UCAUAUUAGUCCUCCACACCUUGCUGAAGUAGCCUCCUGAGACAUAAAUCUGACUCUUCCCUGCUUAAAGCCAUUUACUGCCUGCCUAUUAUCUAUAGGAAAGGCCCAAGCUCCUUAGCAUGACACCAAAGGGAUUUUCAGACCAGCCCUUGCUAAUCCCUCUAGCCUUAGGGGGGCAGCAUAUCAGAGUGAUUAUCUCCCUUACUCUCCCAGUGACUUAACCUUUGUAGCCUGUUUCCUCAUUGCUAACAUUAGGAUGAUAAAACCUACCUCAUGGGUUGGUGAGGAAUUAAUCAGCUCACACAUGGUUAGCCCUCAGUAAACGUUGGCUGUUAUGGUUGUGUCUUUCCACUCUCUGCCUCGCACUUUAAGAUCUGGCUACAUGGUUUUCUGCUGACUCUGUGUCCCUUUUCACCAUGGUUAGUGCCUUUAUUCCUGCCACCCACUCUUCUUGCAAUGUCCUCCAAACCCUGUUGCCUGGCUUCACGCUGGUUAGGCACAUCCUCUUCCUUCUCUUGGAUGCUCCAUGCAUGUGUCGGCCAUUGAGCUGUAAAUAUCUACUAAUAAGUCAGUUACUGCUGCUAGACUAUCAACUUUAUGGGGAUGGGGGGUGUUUUAUUUAUCUUUGUGUUGCUAGCACAUAGCAUGUGUUGAAAAAAAUGGUGAAUGAAUACAUGAAAGAAUAAAAGGAAUUCACAGUCUACUAGGGUGUUUGGGGUCUAGGGAUGAAGGGUGGAAGGCAGCUAAGUAGCUUAAUAAUAACAGGUUAGAGAAUCUGGGUAAAGCUGGGGCUGAGGUGAGAAUUAGGCCCUAUAGGAGUCCAGUGUAGGGAGUUUGCUUGUUGAGUGUGGUGCAUGUAGUGAGGAAGCCUGUUUAAAGUUAUCUCCUCAAUGAAAUAAAGCAGCCCCUUCUAGGCAAUCCUAAUUACUCCCUUUCCUGAAAGAAUAUAUUGCAAAUGGAAGGUCAUGCAAUCUGCCUUCUUGUAAGAUCUUCAAUUUCUCAGAAUACAAUGAAUUCUCUAUUACCUGGAGGAGGGGUAGAAAGGAGCUUCUUUUUAAUUAAAUUGUCUCUGCAGCAGAAAGUGACUUUAUCCUGCCUUUUGAAGUCUUCCAGUUGUCCUCAGCCUGGCUCAAAUCACUCUCCUUGAAUUCAUUGUUACACUAGUGCACCCUGCUUUGUGAGUUAUAAUUUAACGUGAGCGUAUCUAAUUCUCUAAUGAGAUGGAGACUCUUUGGGAGUUUAUGUUUUUUUCCCUGAAAUGUUUAAUGUCAUGCUUUUGAAUUAAGAAGGGCUUCUACAUAUAUUUAUAGACUGGCUGAGUUUCUCCAUAUAUGUGUUAAGAACUUUCAAAUAAUUAGAGCACAGCCUGAAUUUCAGAAUGCCAGUGAUCUUCUCCAGGGCUUCAGCUUCCCUGAAAGAACAGCUACUCAGGGCCUAUUAUUAAAUGUUUAAGGUAUCAUUUUUUAACUUUGAAAUAAAAACUGAAAUAUUUGGAAAAUACUGAUAAACGAACAAACAAAAAAACCUGAACUAACCCUACUAGUAGUAGUGGUAACUACUAUACAAUAGUAUUUGGAGUAUAUCUCUGUAGUCUGUCUUCCUUGGCUUUGUGUCUUUGCUUCUCUUUCUCUUUCAAUGAAUGAGGUCAUCUUUUAUCACUCAUCUGGCAAUCUGCUUUCUUCUCCUUAACAUCAAUAGAUAUUUAUUAAAAGUGAUGAUGCUGGAGUAUUUCUUUUAGGUUCCUGUUUCAAUCCUUGACCCACUGUUUUGCCUUGUUUGCCACUGCCUGCCUUUUCUUGAUUUCUGUUUGUCUCUCUGGAUUGACCCAUUAUUGUGUUCUGAUCUCUGAUACCUGCAUGCAUCUUCAUAGUAACUUCCAACUUUUGGGAGUGUCUGCUGUGCCCCAGAUAGUUGUAUGUGUUUUACCUGCUUUAAAAAUCUCUUUUCGGAUAGACUGGAUAUUUGUAGUCUCCAUGUCACAGAUGAGGAAUUUAUUUGGUGUAGAGAUUUAGUAAUUUAUAAAAGAUCAUGAAGCUUAGAUGGAGCCUGAACUUAUGUUUUUAUACUCAGCACCCCCUCUAGUAUGUGAAACUGUCAUCUUUAGCUUCUGACUCCUUCUGGAAUACUGAUUUUUGGGUGCUGUGUCUAAUCAGCUUUCAGCUCUACAAUAUUCCUUGAAGGGCACCGCAACCCACAACCUUGGGCCAGCAUAGUGAAUUUUAUAUUUUUUAUUUGACAGAGAGAGAGAGAAUGUGUGUGUGUGUGUGUGUGUGUGUGUGUGUGUGUGUGUGUGUGUGUGUGUGUUUGAGAAAUCAGCAGCUGUGGUUCUUGCUUUCACUCCUCAUGGUGAGGAGGUGGCCUACCCCUCACAUCUGUUUUCAGCCCCUGUUCCUCAAUACCAGAGUUAUUUUCUAUUAACUCAAUGCACCUUUUCUUUGUAAUUCUUGUCAAUUUUCCCUCCAGCCACCUGCGCGGUCUCUGGCUUGCUCUCAGGCUGUGAGUAAAUUCUUUGUAUACUUGCUGUUUUCGAUAACCUCAGCCCAAGACUUAAUGUCAAGGUGGGGGCCCUAUUAAAGAUGCCAUGAAUCAUCUUGUCUUUGUUUGAAGAUUUCCGUGUUGGCAAGUGGGCAGAUAGAUGUAGGUUUCCCAACCAGAUGUACUGGUAGCUGAGAUGGGGGCAUUCAGCUGAAGUACAUUCCUAUCAUUAUUUGGCAAAGAAAGAGCCACUGAGAUUAAAAGCAUGAUCCUUGCUUGUGAUCUGGCUUCAUCAACGGAAUCACAGAGCCUCUGUGUUGGAAAGGGCCUUGAAAUCAUCUGCAACUGCGCGGCUUGAUACUUGAGGGAACUGAGGCAAUAGAUACAGGAAGUGAUGUAAAGUUAUAAAUGCCAAACCUUCAAGGGACUUUUGACAUGACGUAACUCUGCGCUCUUAUGUUUUGGGGGAAGAAUAGUAAGGCCUCUAGAAGCUCACUAACACUCCUAAUGCGGCACAGCGCGUUACUGCAGAGCAAGGACUCUACUGACCACAGGCCCAGGACAGCGGCCUUGGAGGUGAAGUCACUAAGGGGGAUCUGUAGGAUUUGGCUGGUUACAAGAGCUCACCCGCUAUCUCCUCCAGGCUGGCUUCCGUGGGCCUCUGUUGAACUAUCAGUCCAGUGUUCUUGCCUCUGUCCCCACAGCCCUGCAGAGGUCUUCUUCCACCUGACAGAUGGUGACUGCCUUCUCCACAGUGGUAGGAGUGAGGGAAACAGUGAGGGGAAAUCAGGAAACAGGAAGCCAGGGAGAGGAGCAAGAGGUGUUGGGGCUGUAUGUGCUGGCUCCGUGCCUUGGUGUUGUGGGUUUCUAGAGGGUUUUAACUUUGUAGUAAAGACGGGACUUGGAGGAAUUCUCCCUGUGGUGGGACAGGAGUUUUCUCCACAGCCUUCACAAAGUAUUCCCCGCAAGAACUACUCAUCCUUCACGGUCUACUUCUAUCGUAGCAGUUCAGUCUUCUGCUGUUUCUUCUGGUACCAGCCUAUGGAUUGGGUAAGGAGAAAGAUCAGGUUUGUAAAGAGAUCUUUCUGGUCCUUCCAGUAAUAAAGCCCCUUGGACAAGGGCCAGGGAGAUUCAUCUCCCAGAGACUCCUGUGCUCUAGGUGGUGGUAGAGGCUUCCUGCCAGAAGGAUCUGAGGCAGAGGACGUGGAUGGUGCCAUGCUGGCGUCUCUGUGCAUCUGGCAGCGCAACAAAGGACUUCUGUCUGCCCUGCGAGGCUGGGUCGGUAAAACCCACUUCAAUUGAAAGCCACCACACUUUAGCAACUUGAUAAUUAAAAUUCUAAUAUGUGAAUUAAAGAAAACAAGGGGCUGUGUUCCUGCCAUAUUAAAAUACAGCUGCAGUGAUUCCACUAUUGUUUCCUUUGACAGAGCUGUGGUUUUCCUACACACCUUUGUUUGAGGCUUUGAUUCAGAUAUACUCCCUGCUGCUGAUAAGUCCCAUGUGUCUACUCAUCGGUUAGAUGGUGCAUGGGGAUGAUUCUUCUGUGAUGUGGAGAAUGAAAGAUCGUGUCUUCAAGUUAUGUGAGGUGGCUAAGUGACAUCUCAUCAAGAGCAGAGAUAAAAACAAAACUCAUGGAAAAGGUACUUCCUGAGCUCCCUUUUUGUUUCCUAAGUGAUUUAAAACAAUAAAGGCCAAAUCGAAGAGAAAACUUAAGAACCGAUAUAGCUGAUACCUGGACUUACGGAUUGAUUUAUUUCUGUGAACACUCUGGGAAAAUGGCCACUUGUCGCUCUCUGUUAUUAAUAAAGAGGUCACUUUAUCAUUAGGCCUUUGAAUCUGUAUUUAAUGGCUAAAGCAGAUGGUUAUAAUUUCUGACUUGGUGUGGCCACCUUAUUAAUAAAAAAGAACUGAUGGAAGCAAAAAGGCGUCUUCAUUUUUAACUCCAGAAGCAUAACACAAAUGCUUUCCAGUCUUUCUUUGUGUGGAGAGCAGACCAAGUGACUGCAAUAAGAUCCUGUUACACAUUUGAAAAAAAGACUUUUGCAGAGUGGAGGUAACUCAGUUUGAAUCCUUCUUUUGUUAAACUUUAAAAGAACACUAUAAAUAUAUGCCCCUUUCCUUGAAGAAGGUAUUUCGAAGGAAGCUUCAGGAUUAUAUUUUAAAGUAAAUUAAUAUUUUAAUAACAUAAGGAAACUAAAAAACACCUAAUUUAUUUCAGAUAGUGGAGGCCUGUGGUACUUUCUAAAAUUAUUCUUUUUGCUUAAACUACUAUAAACUGCUUUUUUGGAUUUAAUUACUAGGCUUAGAUGAAUGUGCCAUGCAUCUUAUUUUGGUUCUUUUUAAAUUCACUUGGAAUUAAAAAAAAUCAAUAAUGGCAAAAACGUCUGGUAGUGGAUUUCUGCUUGAUUUCAUCAAGCCUGUAUAUUCCCCUAUAAUGGUAAGGAGUUUGAAAUCGUGGUUAUCAUCCUGGAAAUUUUUUGUCCCCAAAGGGACAAACCUACAUUUGUGAAGACAGAAUGAUUUAGAAUCUUAAUGUACUCAGUAAACCGAGUGAACAGAGCAGAAAAAUGCUGGGAAUUCUUCACAUAGGCUCAGAAGAGCUCUUUAAUUCACUUAGAUACCAAAGACUUAUUGAUAUGUCAGGCUGUGGGCGGCAUCCUGGGGUCUGUUAUGGCAAUGAAUUCCUGGUCCUUAGGUGACAAGAAUGGGAUGAGUGUGCUAUGCCUGGCUCUGAGAUAAAGAAAAAACAUGGAAUGUUAAGGAUCUUAAAGUCUUUACGGGUUUCUUUGCCCACUAGUUUUCAAUGUUUUUUAAUUAAUGAUGCCUUUCAGGCUGUCCAUGGGCCCACGUUUAGAAGUGUUUUGAAUUUCAAAUUAUUAAUGGUAAUUGUUGUUUUCUGUUUUCAUUAACCAAAGGCAUGUAUAACAACCCAUUCAGUUCAUUUGUUUAUUGAUUUGUUCAUUAAUUCUUCAGUAUUUAGCUUGUAUUUACUUUUGGCUUGGCACCAUGCCAAGCACAGGGAUGCAGAGGAGUUUGUGAUGGCCACCAGUCUUAUUUAAAAUGCCUAAAAUAGGGUCAGGAGCAGUGGCUAACACCUGUAAUCCCAGCAUUUUUGGAGGCUGAGGCUGAAGGAUCACUUGAGCUCAGGAGUUUGAGACCAGCCUUGGCAACAUAGUGACACCUCAUCUCUACAAAAAAUAAAAAAAGUUGGCGGGGUGUGGGGUGGGCGCCUGUGGUCCCAGCUACUCCAGAGACUGAGUUGGGAAGGUCACUUGAGCCCAGGACGUCAAGGCUGCAGUGAGCAGUGAUGGUACCCCACACUACAGCCUGAGGGACAGAAUGAGACCCUGUCUCAAAAAAAUAAAUAAAAAUAACUAAAGUGCUCCACAACAGUGGAUGGAUUUUUGUUUUUCCUACCAUCUCAGAUUCCUGGAUAUCUAGACCAAUCCAUUGCUAAGCCAUCGUGCUUUGUUUUCUUUUUUAAACUUUGAAAUGUUUUAAGUGUACAGAAAAGCAGACAAAAGUGACAAAACCCAUUUCAGAUACAAAUAUUUUUUAUUUGUUUCAGAUUUUUAAAAGAAAUAAAACAUUAUAGAUACAACAAAAGCUCCCAGUGUACCCCUCCUAAAUCCUGUCUCUUUUCUUCUCCAGAGAUAAUCUGUCCUUUAAAUGUGAUGUCUUUUCAUUCCCAUGCAUGUUUUUAUAUUUUUGCUCUCUGUGCAUAAAUGCACUGAGUGCUACUAAAAAUAGUGCUUUGCCUAUUUUAAAAUUGUGUAUAAAUGGGAACUUACUGUACCUGUCAUACAUCUUGCUAUUUUUGCUCAAUGUUGUGUUUUUGGUAUUAACCUUGUUAAUUUAGGAAUUGCAUGUUGAUCUAAGAAGUUAUUUUAGUUGCUGUGCAGUAAGUAUGCUAUUGUAUGACCAUUUCACAAUUAAUGUACCCAUUCUCCUGCCUUCAUUUUUUUGUGUAUUAUAAACAAUUUUGCCAUGAAAACUUUGACUUAUCUUUCUGUAAAAAUGUGUGAAGUUUUUCUAGGCCAAAUACCUAGGAAUAGAAUAGAGUAUGCAUGUCUUCGGCUUCCCUAGGUGCUGUGGAAUUGCUCUCCAACGGCCUUAUGCCAGUGCGAGCUCCUUCCUACAGGAUAUAAGUUCCCGUUGCUCUUUACCCUUUCUAACUCUUGAUAUUGGAAGUAUUUUUAGAUUUUGCUUAUUCAACAGGUAUGAGAAACUAUCACAGUUUGGAUGUAUAAAGAUAUGUCAAGUUGAGUAAAGAUGUUAGAGCAAAGACUGGAGAUUUUUUUUUCCUUUUCCUCCUGUUCUAGCUGUAUUGUUCUAGCUAUAUUAUAGGGCAGAUUUGAGUUUCUGCUUGGGUAGAAUUAUCCUCAUCAAAGCCUACUUUGGCCCUAAUUAGUUUGCUAUACAUCCAUUGUACACAGAACACAUUAUGUACAUUUCUAAGGAAUUGAAGAGACAAAGUCCAAACUUAUAGAACCUAUGUUGGGGGUGCAUAGCAGGAGAUACUGGGGCCCAAUUUACAGUAGGUUCAUUGCACUGGCCAGUGAAUUCAGGGACCUUGCUCUCUAUAUCAGCAGAGAUUGCUGCCUGUGUGGUUUUUUGGUUUUUUGUUUUGUUUGCUUUUUGUUUGUUUGUUUGUUUGAGACAGAAUCUUGCUCUGUCUCCAAGCUGGAGUGCAGUGGCACGAUCUAGGCUCACUGCAACCUCCGUCUCCCGAGUUCAAUCAAUUGUCCUGCCUCAGCCUCCUGAGUAGCUGGGACUAUAGGCGUGUGCCACCACGCCCAGCUAUUUUUUGUAUUUUUAGUAGAGACGGGGUUUCACCAUGUUGGCCAGGAUGGUCUCAAUUUCUUGACCUGGUGAUCCGCUAGCCUCGGCCUCCUAAAGUACUGGGAUUACAGGCGUGAGCCACUGCGCCCGGCCGCUUUUUGGGUUUUAAUGUCCAUAAAAUGAGAGAUUGCAUUAGUCAUUCCUUCUUCAAGAGCAGAUUUUCUUUUCUGCUUUCAAAAUUCCAUGCUUCUAAGUGGCGUUGACCCUUGGUGCUUUAAAACGUCUUAAAAAUCACUGAUACUUAAUUGGUAUUGAGAACAGAGGAACUUAAUGCAGGAGCCACCACUAAGUGAAGAGCAGUUAAAAAAUGCUAAGAAGUCACCUGCAAAAUUCUAAUCUAAUUAAAAUUAUGUAAAAAAAGACCACCAUCACUCAUGUAUAAAGAUGACAGGGAAAAAUUACAAUGAAUAGACUGUGGGUGAUUAUUCCCCUCAUUGCCCUAUUUUUCUGUUUUCCAAAUCUUUUUUAAUGGUCAUGGAGUAAUAUUCUUGGAAUAAAAUAAUAAGCAUAUGCAAACAAUUAUAAGCUCAUUUGGUAGGAAAAUAAGAAUGUGAUUUAUACAAAACAUGUGCUGGGCAAAGGGGAGAACACCUGUAUAUGAAAAAUGAUUUGUAAUGAUUUUGUAAAUAAUCCUAUAAUCCUUCCUUGGGUUAAGGGUUGGUGGAUGAUAAGUGUUUUUCUUUAGGUUUUGCUGCUGGAAAGAUCCAGGGAAGAUGGAAGACAAGUAGACUGGCAUCUUACCUAAAAGCAGUGGCACAGCAGGUGGUAGAAUAAUUUGAGCUUCGCUCAUUGGAUUUUAAGACCAAAAGAAAAGGCAGAACUAAAGAGAUUUUAUUCAUUAGGUCACGUAGAUAUUCCUAUUCCAAAGGCAUAUGACAAAUCCUUCAGAGUUGAAGUAAUCAUAAUGCCUACAAUAUAUUAAGCAUUAAAUAUACAUAUAUUUUUCAAUUCUGGAAUAGCUGUGAAUGUGGGAAUAACUGUACUGACUGACAGGGGAGAGAUCAGAUAGUUUAAGAAACUUGCCCCAUAUGCACAGCUCAUCAGUGGUGCUGCCUGGACUCAGCCACCAUCUGUUUCACUCUGCCGGGGCAUACAUGUAUGUGUACCCUUGCCCUGGCAAACUCUUCCUUUUGUAGAGCUGAAAGCAGCCCCCUGCAACUUUCCUAUGUAUUUAUUCUCAUCCUGCCCUCCUGAGCACCCAGCCUUAGAAGUCUGCUCCCUCUUUCGCACAACAGCCUUUCUGAUCUUCAAAGAGGGCUAUUGUGUCCAUUUCUCCACUUCUCCCCUCUUCGGUCUGUCAUCUUGGAAAAGCUCAGAGAGGUGUUUUUAUUCACAGAUGCCUUGAGAAAUUUCAUGGUUUUUAGACUCAUGCUGAGUUUGUCCAGAUGUGCCAAUAUUUGUCUUAUAUGAUACAAAUUAAUUGUCCAGAAGAGGAAGAAACCUUUGUAGACACUCACUAAUGCAAACCAGUUCCUUUGAGUAUUGAUGGAAGGAAAAACACUAAAAAAUGAAACAGAUCAUUUUCACUGGGAGAGUGUAGUUGUUGAAUUCACAUUCUACUUUUAGGACAAAUCUGUAGCAUGACAGUUCAGUCUUACCACAUGUAUUAACCAUGGGAAACCUAGGGUGACAUUUGCAAUAGACUCCUGCUUUUCUGUAAGGACUUUAUACAGAUGGAGAAAGUAUGAUACUCUUACAUUUUAUUACCAAGUUCUGUGGCCCAGGGUUUACAGCAUAAGGUGGCAAAUAAUUUAGCUCCACUCAGAUUUGGAAGAGUAACUAUUAUUAUUAUAAGUAAGAUUUAAACUUAGGGACAGGUACACACUCUUUAAGGAGAGUUCUAAGACUGAGAUGUUGUAUCAUUAUCAGUACCUGGCAUAAAUAUAUGUAUCUGAGUUCUCUUUGAGAAUCAUAAGGGAAAAGAUGUCUAAUAUGAUUUAACCUCAAGACACUAACAAUGAUUACACCUAUCCCCUGCUCCCAGCAUCAUAGUCACCAACUGUGGCAACAGCUGCUGCUAAUGUUUUUUGAACUCCUGUGGUAUGCCUGGUGAUGUACUUUAUAUCAGCUAGUUCAUUCUCAAAACUUGAGAACACACUACAUAUACCCUAGUAAGUACUAUUGUUAGCCUCGUUUUAUAGAUGAAAAAACUGAGAGGUUAAGUAUUCUGCCCAAGAUCAUAUAUAGGUUGGGUAUCCCUAAUCUGAGAAUCCAAAACCCAAAAUGCACCAAAAUCUGAAACGUUUUGCAUGCCAACAUGAUGCUCAAAGGUGCUCCUUGGAGCAUUCAGAUUUUGGAUUUUUGGAUUAGGAAUGCUCAGCUGGUAUAAACGCAUAUAUUCCAGAAUCUUGAAGACAUCUGAAACAUGUCUGAUCUCAAGCAUUUUGGGUAAGGGAUACUCAACCUGUAUCUUGUAUAUAGUAGAGUGAGAGUCUAGCUUAUGCUUUGCUCUUAUAUCUUGUUUCUUUCUUCAGCAAAAUAGUCUGUAAAUUGAACAUUAAACAGUGCACUGGGGACACAGUAAGGAAUCUUUCAUUACCAAUGGAGCAUGAAUGAAAGUUUCCAAAUAUGAGGUUUCCUUAGUGAAACACUAUUUUUAGGAAAAACUAUUAAACCAAGGCUUAUGAUAAAGGAUCAUUCCACAUCCAAAUAUACCUCUCCUGUAUUAGCAUAAUUCUCUACUAAAAUCACAGCUGAAAUUCAUUCACUCUAAGAGAUGGAUAAAAACCAUACGGUUUCAUGUAAAGAUCACCAGCUUCCCAGAACUAGGAUGAUGGGAAUUUUAACUAAUGCUGCUGUGACUGUGGCCUAGCCUCUUACUCUUUCUGGAUCUCAGUGGGCCCAUCUGUAGAAUGUGAGCAUUGGCCUCUGUGAUAAUGAAUGUUCCUUCUAGCUUUGUAUAUUGCAUAGUGCAUGACUGCUAGCUUCAGGAAAAAUAAAACGUUUUCAAUGGAAAUAUCAGAUCACCAACCUGAUUCCAAUGAAUUUUUUUUUAUUCACUGAGGCUUUAUGUCAUAUAAAAAUAUGUGACGUAUUACUGCUCUGCUGCCCAUCUAUUUAAGGCAUUCUUCAGUAGACUUGUCAGGGCUUAUCUAAAUCUUAGCACCACUUACGUGUGGCUGAUUGCUUGGCAGGAGGAGGUUCCUGCAUUUUCUUCCUCCUGUGUAUUAGUGAAUUGAAAUCAAGGGAAAAACUGCUUGGCUUUCUGCUUCCUUCCAUGGUAGGUAGACUUUUCUACAUAUUUUCCAACAGUUCUUUUUGACAGCCAAGUCUGGAAACAGGGCAGGAUGGAGGUUUUACAAAUAGGUGACAGUUGUUUGUCUCAUGAAUUUCUUCUAUUUCCUUUCCCUAGUGGAGUUAACUGCCUCCUUCCUACAACAAUCCGAACGUACUUCCAUCACAGAGUAUCUAGCAGUGUGAGCAAUAGCCAUUUCUCUCUUUUACCUCUUCUGGAUUCUAAACCCAUCAUAGGUAGAGAUAGAACAUGUCUGUGCUUAGAUAGUAUCUGGCACAUACAGAUUGCUCACUUAAUGGUGAAUGAAUGAAUAAAGAAGAAAAAGUGAUGAAAGAAGAAAAACUACAGUCGUCUCUUGGUAUCUGUGGCACAUUCGUUCCAGGACCCUGAUGGAUGCCAAAAUCCUUGGAUGCUCAAGUCUCUGAUAUAAAAUGGCAUAGUGUUUGCAUCUAACCUACAUACAUUCUCCUGUAUACUUUAAAUUAUCUCUAGGUUACUUAUAAUACCUAAUAUAAUAUAAAUGCUAUGUAAAUAGUUGUUACACUGUAUUUUAAAAUUUGUAUUAUUUAUUAUUAUUAUUUAUUUACUUAUUUUUCCAAAUAUUUUUGAUCUGUGGUUGAUUGAAUCCAUGGGUGUGGAACCUGGGGAUAUGGAGGGCUGACUAUAUAUACUAAUGAACACUACUUUGGAUUAUAUGAAAAUACCCAUUUAUGAAAUGGACAGUUCAAAUGUUUCCUCUUUGACUGUUCUUAACCUGACCUCCCAACUUGAAGUAAUCUGUUCCUCUCCUCUAAACAGUUAUGUGUACUAUGUGUUUGGUAAUUAAUUAUGUACUGACUCAUGACAUUUGUUUCUGUUCUUAUAAUACUUUUUGAUUUUCAAAUACCUUAUGACUUUGUUUUUUAUUACAAUUUGUUUUCCCAUCAAGAUUGUAAAUUCUUGGAGGCAAGGGCAAUUAUUAAAUACUAUAUUUGAUACUUAAUUCGCUCCUCUCCUUUGGGGGCUCCAGUUACAUGUAUAUUAGGCCAGUUGAAGUUGUUCCUCAACUCACUGAUUCUGUUUACUUUUUUAAUUCCCUUUUUCCCUCUGUAUCUUAUUUUGGAUAGUUUUGAUUUUUGUGUUUUUGAGUUUACUAAUAUUUAUCCUCUGCAAUGUCUAAUCUGAUGUUAAUCCCAUCCAGAGUAUUUUUCAUCGCAUACAUUGUAGAUUUCACCUCUAGAAGUUUGAUGUAGCUCUUUUUUUUUUUUUGAGACGUAGUCUUGCUCUGUUGUCAGGCUGGAGUGCAGUGGUAUGAUCUCGGCUCACUGCAACCUCCGCCUCCCUGGUUCAAGUGAUUCUCCUGCCUCAGCCUCCCAAGUAGCUGGGACUAUAGGCGCAUGCCACCACGCCCCACUAAUUUUUUUUUUUUUCUGUAUUUUUAGUAGAGACGGCGUUUCACCAUGUCGGCCAGGAUGGUCUUGAUCUCUUGACCUCGUGACCCGCCCACCUCGGCCUCCCAAAGUGCUGGGAUUACAGGUGUGAGCUACCACGCCCUGCUGAUGUAGCUCUUUUUCAUAUCUUCAGUGUCUCCACUUACUUUUUGAACUUAGGGAAUAUAGUUAUAAUAACCAUUUUAAUGUUCUGUCUGCUAAUUCUAACAUCUGUGUCAGUUUUGAUUGACUUUUUUUUUUUUCCUCCUCAUCAGGGGUUAUAUUUCCCUGCUUUAUGAAUGCCUGGUAAUUUUUGAUUAGAUGCCAGACAUUGUGAAUUUUCCUUGUUGGGUACUGGCUAUUUUUGUAUUCCUACAAAUAUUUUUGAACUUUGUUCUGGAAUGUGUUUAAGUUGUUUAGAAGCAGUUUGAUCCUUUUGGAAAGUCUUGCUUUGAAGAUUUGGAAGACUGAAAUAGUUGUACUUAGUCUAUAACUAAUUAUUCUCCAUGACAGUGAAAACACUCUUCUAUGUGCUCUCCUCGUGGCGUGGGGAAUCAUGAGGUUUUCCAAUCUGGAAAUAUCUUUUUGGAUAUUUCUUUCCCCAGUGCUGGGUAGUUGCCACACAUGUAUGCACUGAUCAGCACUCUGCUGAAUACUUGAGGGGGAUUCUCUGUGGCUCUUUCUGCAGCUCUCUUUUCUCUGAUACUUGGCCUUGCAAACUCUAGUUGCCUUGGUCUCCCUGGACUGUUAGCUCAAUUCACUCAACUCAGGCAGUUCACUGAGCUCUGCCUGAGUUCUCCCUUUCCUCCAGACACCUUGAGCUGGAAAUUCUCUCAGGCAGUAAGCUGGAGGACUCGUAGGAUUCGUUUCAUUUGCCUUCCUUCUUCCAGGGAUCACUGCCCUUUACUGACUGUUAUACCAGUCUUGACAAUUAUCCUGUUACUCCAACUUGGCCAGAAAUGGAAGUGAUACAUUUUAUUCUUUCUGUCUGAAAUAAUCCUCCAUCCCCAAUGUUUAAAAACUGCCAUCCUUGACUCCAUGUGACUGUGUUAGGAGCCCUUUCUCUGGUCUCUCAUCAUACCUGUGCUUACAGUAAUUUAGUGCGGCACUCCUCUCCCUGCGUUGUUCUUGCAUUUUUUUUUACCCUCUCUUUUCUCGUUAGAUUUUGUUUCCUUGAGGACAGGGAAUGUCUUUAAUCUCGGGAUUUCUAACACCUAACAUAGACUCAGGUGUGUAACAGUUGCUCAAUAAGUACUUGUUGAAUGAAUGAAUUAAUAAAUAAAUAGGAUUCAAUUUUCAAAGUAUCUGUUGUUGAACAACUUUCAGAAGUUUUUUUUUUUUUUUACAGAAAUGAGAUUAGAUAUGCAUCUUCAUAUAUGCAAUUGAAAUCUCUCUUAAAUUUCUAGAUAAUCAGUUGUUGUUGAUGGCUUGGACAUGGUUUUUACCUAUUUAUUUUUUGUAGCCUCUCCUUAGAAGGUGUUAAUAAAAGCCACCUAGUUGAUGCUUGAAACAACAUGUGGAGGUAAAGGGACCAAGAAUAGAAUAGCCAUAUUCUAUAAACAAACAAAAUGAAGACUAACUUUUAGGUAUCUGUUUUAUGAUGGACCCUCAGAUGUGGUAUAUCCCAAGUCUGCCAGGAGGUUGUUCUUAUCUGAAGUGCCUUUUCCAUGUUGGAUGUACUUAGAUGCCUUUUAUCCAGGUAGACUCAGAUGGUCUGCAAAUAGCUCUAUGGAUUUGGCAUUGGAAAACCUCAUGGUUCCCCAGGCAUGGGGAGAGCACAUAAAAGUGUUUUCUCUGUCAUGGAGAAUAAAUAGCUGUGAGUCGUUGCAUUCUUAUCAACUGGAGACAAUUGACAGUGGAUAUGUGCCACUAGAGUUAUGGUCAAGUGCAAGUUCAUACUAUAUUUGGAUCUUUAAGAGUCGGUAGAAUGAACCAUAUUUGGUAAGCCUCUGAAGACUGUCUUGCUCCAUUUCCUCAGCAGCUCUUGGUUACCAAAGGUGACUCUGGAGCCCCACCUCCAAGUCCCCAUCCUGCACAGUUGGCAUGAUGGAAAUGGCUUGAGGUUCUUGUUCUUUCAGAUUCAGUGUUUUCAUCUGUGCAGUAGGAUAUAAGUAGGAUAAGAUGUAAUUUGUCAGGUUGCUAUGAGGAAUAAAUGAAGUAAUAAAUGUUAGUUGCCUAUCACAGUUUCAGGCACAUGGGAACCCUCUCCCCAUUCCCCCAAACUUAAUUGAAAAGAUAGCCAUCAGCCUCUGAAGUUGAAUUGUGCUGAGUGGUUACUAACAUUAAAGACAUAUGGAGUUAUUGUAUCUGUAUCUUUCACUUAUCAGCUUUUCCUUGAAGGUUUAAUGUGUGUUCCUUUGCUUUUAGGCCCCAUGUUUAUUUUCCUGAAAUGGUGUCUUCUUGACUUAAAGUACAAUCUUUGCUUUUUUAUUCUUUUUUCACUGCUCUUGCCUGGUGAUCCUGUUGUUUAAAGACAUCUCCAUCCUUCCCUAUCCUUUCCCUUUCAAAUCUAUGGCCCAGACUGGGGGUGGCUUUAACUAACAACAGCACUUUGCAUUAGUUAAGUAGAGUGGAAUUUCUCAUUCUACCUCUCAGCUAUUGAUGAAACCUUUCCCUGAUGCACAAAUUAAGACUGGGUGUAUUUUGCAUAUUUUCCUAGAAUGACACAGUGAUUCUGUGGCUAAACCAAGAUUAGACCCUACCACUUUAAAAAAUCUGACUUUUUGCUUAAAGUGUAAACUGUGUUGCUUCUAAAACUACUAGUUGAAUUUAACUUUCAAGUGUACUUUGUAUUUAAAUCUGAUGAUAGUGUUGUUUUUCCUUUUGUCUUGUUUAGAUGAGGGUAUUUUCUUCACUUCCCUGACCCCUAGUGCCUCAGUGACCUAGGCAGCAAGUUUUUUGAUGCUGUCCAGAAUGCUAAUUAAGAUAUUUAUUCUCUUUGGCCCUAUUGUUUAUGAUACUUGUAAUUAUGUCUAUUAGAUGGUAAUCUCUGUUAUCUCCCACUAUACUAAGUGUACUACUCGGCACAUAAAGAAAUGUGUGAGUAUGUGAAUGUAUACUCACAUGUUUGAAUAAAUGUGAAUAAAUCAAUAUAUUUAUAUAGUUACUGAUUUAAAUGUGUUCCGUCUUGGGAUGUGAGAUGGGAUAAUUGAAUAAGAAAUUAGCCUGUGUGUGUUAAGGUAGUCAAAGUUUUUAUGGUACCUUUGUACAAACUGCCCCUUCUGUUGUGUGUGUGCUGACCCAUGUCAUGAUGCUCAGCAUGACUGGAGGAGUCCUGGUGUGUUUCUGUCCUCACUUGCUCCCUGGGUUGGGCGCCCCUCUGCAGGGUACAACCAACACAGUUGUAUGAAGACCCUCUGACUUUCAUUUUCUGGCUGGCUGGGGGUUUUGGUGUUGAGCGCUUUUAAGUAAGACAGUCACCUUAUCCUACUCAAUGUUUUCUUGAAGUGCAGGCCCUGUGAAGAUGAAGAUCCCCUCUUCUAUUUUGGGGACACUUUUGUGAUGCUUUUAUCUGUCUCUCCAGAGUCUGAUUUAAUGAAAAUAUGUACCUCCCUCACCACAUUCUGCAAAGCUUACUUGAGUUUUUAAAAUUUAAUAGUAAAUAUGUUAGUACAUGUUGAUUCUAGUGCCCAGCACAUAGUUUCUGCUCAAUACUUAGCUAUAAUUAUUAGUUUAUUUAAAUUGCCUUAAUCAUUCAUGCAAUAAGCAAAUGUCCCCCCUGUAGGCUGUUCUCCAGAUCUGGGAUACAGACAUGGGUAAAGCUUGGAGCUUGUGUAUAAGUAGCGGGGUCAGUCGCCUGCCAGUUCACUGGAGAGAUGCCAUGCUUGGAGGGUGGACUGACUGUAAGGCCCUCCCAGUUGUCAGACUCUAGGCUUCUAGUGUGCCCUCCCUCACUGUACAGCUGGUCAAUGCAUGGCACUAGAAAGUGCAAAGGCUUCAGUGUUGGAUGAGUGUGGAUUUGAAUCCCAGCUGUGUUGUGGACUAGCUCUGAGCUUCAGUCUCUUCCUCUUAAAAUGGGAAUAAUAGGGUAGUUGCAAAGUGUCAUUGUUAAUUAGGCCCUGGGCUAAGUUCUUUACUCCUGUGAUUUUAUGAAAUCCUCAAACAGCCCUGUGAGGUGUGUCUUGUUAAUAUCUGUAUUUUAUAGAUGAGGAGCCUGAGGCACAGAAGGGUGAAGAAACUGGCCUAAGUGGUAGAGCUUUUCACUGAACCCAGGCCUAUUAGAGAGCAGAGGCCACAUUCUUCACUGUUAUGCAGUGUCAUGCUAUGUUAUCUGUCCAGACAUGUUACGAUUCCUGGCACACAGGAUCAGAGCAAAUAGUAGCUAUUAUUCUUAUUACUAUUAUUGUUCUAAAAUUCAGGCCUUUCUUCACCACACUGACACUGAGUAAUAUAUAUUGUAGCUGUUCAAUAAAACUUUAUUGGAUUUAAUUGGUUAUGAAUUUUAUGUGUGGGAAGGUGGUUAACUUUCCUAUCUGUAAGGAGAAAUGCUCAAUAGAAUAUCUUAAAAUGGGGGAAGUUAUGAAAAUAUAAAAUAACAACCAGAGAGGCAAACCAGUUUAUGAGAUUCUGUAUUAGAAAGCUGGAAAGAAGUUUUUAAUAAGAAGAAUGGAGGCUGGGCGCAGUGGCUCACACCUGUAAUCCCAGCACUUUGGGAGGCCGAGGUGGGCAGAUCACGAGGUCAAGAGUUCGAGACCAGCCUGGCCAACACGGUAAAACCCCAUCUCUACUAAAAAUACACACACACACACACACACACACACACACACACACACACACAUACACACACACAAAAUAGCCAGGUGUGGUGGCACGAGCCUGUAAUCCCAGCUACUCAAGAGGGUGAGGUAGGAGAAUCGCUUGGACCUGGGAGGUGGAGGUUGCAGUGAGCAGAGAUCGCACCACUGCACUCCAGCCUGGGCAACAGAGCAAGAGUCUGUCUCGGGGAAAAAAAAAAAAAAAAAAGAAGAAGAAGAAUGGAAGGGUACAAUCUGGUGGUAGACACCAUUUGAAAAUAUUCUGUCUAGCAAAUAGUGUUUUUGAGUAAAAGAAAUAGACAUGACAAAUCAGUUAUGUGGCCAUCCCUUAUAACAAUGAUGAACAGAUAGGAGGGUGUGCAAUCUUUAAAGUUUAGAAACAAAUUUGUCCUUCUGACAUCCUUCCCUUCUCUUGACACACGGUUGGUAAUGGCCAAGAUUCUGUUUUGCCUGAUGGAGUUUUGAGUGAGUUAAAUUAGGUUGUCUUGAAAAUAGCUGGGCCAGAAAAUAAAAAGGUUUUCUCUCUUUGGAAAGGGGCUUUACUCCAGGGAAGAACACAGCUGUCCAGGAGGAAUCCGGGACUGUUGAGUCCAGAAACUUCGAUCCUUCUCCACCCUUUCCCCAGUGUUUCACCAGCAGAAAAAGAAUGUUAUUAAAGUCUGUGAUGAAACAAAGCUGCACGCUGAGACGUGGCUGCCAGAACUUUUAUUUUUAUGGUUCUCUUGAGUUUGGGGAGAAAUAAUUAAAUGUUGCAAAUGUAAAAAUUGGCAGUAACAUUUUCCAUUUUGCCAAUAGUCAUUCCUUUGGUUUUCCCUUGGAUUUUAUUUAUUUCUUUCUCCUUUUAGGCAUUGCUCUGUCAUAGCCUGCUUGAGUGUUGUGUCUCUAGGAAGGCCAGAACACCAGGUUUGGAUGUUACAUAGCCAAGAACAUUGUGUAGCAGUGCCUGGUUUUGCCACAAGACAGGUCUGUAGGAAAUACCACUGCCACUGCAGCCGAGCACGUUGAACUGACUGUGCUCAGGAAUACUUCACCAGUAGGCUUACUGGAAGGUAUGUCUUUCUGCAUCUGUGAUUUGCAGAGGGGCAUAUGAUUGCCUUGCUGUUGGAAACAUAGGAAAUAUGGUUUUUGGGGAUUCUACUUUGAAAUAAUGGUACUCGUCAAUGCAGUGGGAAACUACAAUAUCAGGAUGUUAAGAAAGGGUUCAAAAGGUUUUAGGAAGUCUUGAAAGAUAAAUGCCCAUUCCAAUUGAGCCAGUAGGUCAGUCUUCUUAGGGUUUCUGUGAUAAUAUAGGACUUUAGAGUGGAGACGCCUUUCCUGACAAGUCUAGGGUUGAUUUUAUGUAUUUGCUAAGAUUUAUUAAAAUAAAAAAUGGCAUAUUCUAUAAGGAAAAAUAAUAUUAAUGGUAUUUUAAUUAAGCUUAAGCAAUAAAUAAUGGUUAUCACAUAAUUUUUAUUUAUUAUUCUUUACCUUAUUUCAGGGUCUGUCUUACUGUGAAGUUUCAAUAAAAUGCUUAGAACUACAUUUUCCUGGCCAGGUGCAGUGGCUCAUGCCUGUAAUCCCAGCACUUUGGGAGACCGAGGCAGGUGGAUCACUUGAGCUCAGGAGUUCGAGACCAGCCUAGCCAACAUGGUGAAACCCUGUCUCUACUAAAAAUACACAAAAUUAGCCAGGUAUGGUGGCACAUGCUUGUAAUCCCAGCAACUUGGGAGGCUGAGACAGGAGAAUCGCUUGAACCCAGGAGGCAGAGGUUGCAGUGAGCCAAGAUCAUACCACUGUAUUCCACCCUGGGAGACAGAGUGAGACUGUCUCAAAAAAAAAAAAAAAAAAAAAAAGAAAUACAUUUUGUUUUAUUGCAGGCAGGAUACAUUUCAAGAGGCUUACUUCACCUUCUCUGUCUGAUCUCCGCCAAAUAUCUUGGCUUUGUAUUUCCCAUAACCCAUCUGUUCUUCAUGUAGCUGUGAAAGAAGUAUAUCUUUGAAAGCAGAAUUUUGAGUAAAGAAACCCGAGAGUUAGGGAGAGAUGACCAGGUUCCAUGGCUCCUUGUUAAUUUCACCUUCAAGCCACAUACUGCCUCUUCUUGGGCCCUUGAUCUACUGCUGAGCAUAUCUUUUUCUUUCUUGGUGUGAAUUCUGCCUCUCAGUAUAGGUGGUAUUUGUUAAUUUAACUCUGACAUAAACAUGGGAACACUGCGCCUCAGUGUCAUUGUCUGUAAAAUGGGGUUAUAAGGUAUUUUCUGACCUACUUAAGGUUACCGUGAGGAUUAAGUGAUAAUGUACAAAGAAGACUUUUAAAAAUUAAUAUUGGAGUAUAGUAUAAGCAUAGUGACAUACAAUGAAUUAUAAUCAAUAAUAAAUUGAAUUUCACUUUGUGACCUCAUAAAAUUUGAUUCCUUUCAGCUCUAUCAAGGACAGCAUCUUGCCUAAUCACUUUUUGUUUUAGAAAAGUUAGAUGCUUGUCCAAUGUCACAAAGCAAGUUAGGGUAGAGGUAGGGCAAAAGCCCUGAUCUCCUGACUCCCACACCAGCAGGAUGCUUAGUUGUGAUUUCUGCCUUGCUUUACCACUUGGGUCAUCUUUCAGUGAAGGAGGUAACUAUCUCUUCUUUCUUGAGUUAAAAUAAUACCUUAGUAGAAGCAAAGAACACUAUCACUUUAGUUCUUUUCAGCCUUCAUUUGCUGUUGCCUUCUGUGUCUAGGCGUGCUGAGCUGGCAGGAAGGUGACAAGUAUGAUAGAUUCUGGCCUCUAAGGGGCUGUCAAGUCUAGUGAAAGGAGGUAAAUGAGUAAACAGAUAGACACUUCGGAGCCUGAGUUUCUGGUGCUGGCCCUUACACACAGGGUCUAUCUGGGCAAGUCAUGCCUGUCUUUGGGCUCAGGUUUCCCAGCUGCACAUUGAGGUCCUGGACUAGAUGUACAGAAUGAUCGUGAUCACUGAGGUUCCUUCUAAUUUGUCACCAUCUAUGGGUCUGUGAUAAUGCAAAGCUGUGUGCUUGCCAGCUGAAACUGAAAUGAAGGAAAGUGAUUAAUUCAUUUCACAAACUGAAAUGAAGGAAAGCUAUUAAUCUGAUGGCGUAUUUUUCUUUAUUUGUGAUAAGUUUCACAGACUACAUUUUCCAGCAUUCAACACUGCCAUUGUAUUGUAUUGUAUUGUAUUGUAUUGUAUUGUAUUGUAUUGUAUUGUAUUGUAUUGUAUUGUAUUGUAUUGUAUUGUAUUGUAUUGUAUUGUAUCAUAGAUGGCGAUACUUGUUCAGUUAACCAAAUGGUCAACUUUGCAAAAAUAGCAGAAGUGGACAUCUCAUGAUGAUUUAAUACAGGACACAAAAAUCAAUGCUAGCAUUAACUACUAUUCUCGGCCUUUCUGCAGUGUUUUUCUGAUAGGAACCUUUGUAUUAAACCACCUUCUUUUUUUCCUAAAAAGGACCAUAGCAUAAUAGCAGCUAGCAUUUAUUUGGUGUUUUCCUGUGUGAUAGGUAAGUGUUGUUUUAAGUGCUUCCCAUAUAAAAAUUCAUGUAAUCUUUGCAGCAUUUUGAAGUAGGCAUUAUUAUCAUCCCUAUUUUAGAGAUAAGACAACCGAGGUACAAGAAAUUAAGUAAAACUUAUUCAAGAUUACACAGCUAUUAAGAGAUGGAGGCAGGAUUCAAACUCAGGCGGUCAGCCUCAGGCAGCCUCAUGUUUCAUGGCUGGACCAUUGCCUAAAUGAAAGCUGCUCACUCUCAGCCUAUUGAGAACCUGGAGAAACUGGCCUUGUUAUGAGGCCACAGGCUAAGAAAGCAGUUGUAUCAGCUUACUUGUGGCUCUAAACUUGGCCAGAUCCUCAAGUCUAAGGAUUCUUACUAUGCACAGGUGUUCUCAGUCUGGAUUCAUGUCUCAGGUGACUCAUGAACCCUUGGAAAUUGUGUGCCAAAUGCAUUUAUGAGUCCAUGUGUGUUGUGUUGGUAUGACGGGGGGUAGGCGGUUUGGUGGUUUUCUGCACAGUAUCAGCAGAGCCUCUACUCUGUCACUGGCAGGAUCCUAGCUGUGCAGGCGUUUGUCAGCCUAAAUCUAAAUCAAGAUUCUGGGCUGGGAAUUAGGAUAUAGCUCCCCAUUGAACAAGUGAGUGGCUAUAGGAUCUUGGAAGAACCAGGCUUUCCAAAUGUCCUCCCACCCCUUGGAACUCUGCUGCUGUGGAGCAGUUGUACGAUGUCCUUUUCUCUCUUUGAAGCUUUCCAAAUCUUUCAAUCUUUUUUUUUUUUGCCUCCAAAUUUUGGAACCUCAAAAUUUCAAGGUUUUUUUUUUUAAUUUUUUUAUUUUUUUUCCUUUUGUUUUACCUUCUCCUUUCUGGCUUUGUUCAGAAAUCAGGUAUCAAUAAGCUUUUUAUUACUCAUCCAAUCUGUGAGUUCAGUUUCCCAUUUAACUUUUAUGAAUGUUUUCUUUGUUAAGAUGAGUCCUUUCAAACCCCUGUAAAGAAUGUUUCACUAUAUACAAACAUAAAAACGAAGUGUUAAAACUAGAAAAUCCAAGUGGAAACACAAACAUACAUAUACAUUUUUCCCCAGGCAAUUUAGCUUCAUAGAAAUUGAGUGCAUCUGCAAGGGAAUUUUUUUUUAAAUGUUAUUGGUAGUUUUGUUAUUUGUAUUACCUGUUUGGUCCUAGUCUUUAUAGUUGAUUACUCUAGGUAGGUCUUUUUAGGACUGAAAAUAGGUCACACAUAUCACAGUGGUCCCAGUGUUAGAGAGAUGAUAAAAUUCUAUUACAAAGUAGUUUUGUCAUGCUUUUGGUCUAAAUGAGUAAUACAACUAGCAUGUCCAGUGUCAUUUUUGCUGUACUCUGGAAAACUUUUACCAUCUAUCUCAUCCUUAUAUACUGCAACAAACUUCUGAUAUUAUUUCAAUUGCAGUUCAGGCAUUGCCCUCGACACAGGCUUAAGUUCAAGUCUCAGCUCUGUUACUUACAAACCAUAUGACUUUGAGCAAGUUUAUUUAAUUUUGUGGAGUCCUUUUUUUUCCCAUACAAGGGGAAAACAAUAAUUACAUGUUGCUCAAAGGGUUAUGAGGAGUGAGGUCAGGCAUGUUUAUAUGUUUCACUCUGGCGUUUUGCAGAGUAAGCACUUGAUAAAUGAUGCUCGUGUUAUUGAUUGUCAUCAUCAUCAUUAAUAUGUGUAAUAGGCUAGGUACAGUGCUUGGCACAUAGCGGGCACUAAACAAAUAUUUUAUUGGAUUUGAUUGUACAUAGCGCUUGUGACUGAAUCAGAGGUUGCCAGGGGUAGCUUUUUGCUCAGUAGAUUAACAAGGAGGAAAUUGUUGAACAGAACAACUGAUGGCUCUACCUUUAAGUCAAUGAAUUUCAUAGUGAAGUGGUCUUGAAUGCAAAUGAUGAAAUGUGGCAAGUCUGGUGGAGAAAAAAACCCAACAAUCUUGAAGCUGUUUUAAAGAGUAGCAGUUGCCUAGUCACCCCAAUUGCUGAAAUUUUCCUUCUCUUCCUUGAAUAAGGAGUAGAGAGGGGCAGAGAGGUUACUGGUCAUGUUCAUUAAUUUUCUUUCAAGAACUGCCACAUGUCACCAGUGGUGCCCCCCCAGCACCAGUGCUGUUUGGCAGUCUUCUCUUUGCCCCAGAGAAGCCAAAAUGUUAAAUUGAUGGAGCUUACUAGAUCUGACAGAGAAAUUCUUCACGUCUGGCCUGGAUGUCUAAGUAAAUUUGGUGUACUUCUUGUGGUCUGGAGCAAAUGCUGGAAGCUAUUAGAAUUCUGAACAAAACCCUCCAUUCAAAGACUGCUCGUUUCCUGCUGGGGUAAUCCAAGUAUCAAACAUUAAGAAAUAUGGGCAAGGCAAAUGUGGCUGCUCAUUGCAAAACCCACCAAGGUGUCUACGACAUCUCCCCAAAUGACUUGGAAUGUUACAUCCACUUGAUCAUCUUGAAUAAGUGGUUUCUUUUGAAAACAAGAGCUCUACUUUUCCUACACCAAGUAUAGAUGGGAAUUGGCUGAAUUUCCUCUUGUCAGUCAAAUUUAGGAGAAGAAAGCUUUCCUCCUUCCCUUGAAGUUCUAGGGACCUAGCCUUUUUUUUUGGUUUUAUUUUGUUUCAUUCUCCUUUCCUUAUAUAUUUCCUUCUGAAAUAAAAAAAAGUAUCUUUCAUUAGAUAUAGUUAUGGAUCUAUUGUUUUAGACUAGGCCUGCUCAGUGGCUGGAAACGAUUUUAUUAAGAAGGCUUUAUAGAGAAGCUUUGGUUUAUCUCAUGAAAUAUCUGAGUUUGUCAUAGAUUGUUUCCUUUCUGUACAGAAAGUUAUUUUCUGUGAAAUUCCAGGUGUUCUUUUACAUAGACUUGAAAGGAAUAGAUUUGAUAGUCCAGGUUUUUUUUUUCCCUAAGAAGAAUAUGUUCUUGUGAUAGAUUAAUUGAGGAUGAAAUCAGAUAACAUAGAUGAAAUCACUGGAUAGGCAUAGUGAAAACCAUUAUUUUAAUUAAUCUAGCUACAGUGUUUGUACAGCCAGCUAUGCAGCUGAAGGCUGCCAUGUAGUAGCUGCUACACUGUUUGGCUCCUGUACUUAUACUGUAUGGGGACCUCUUUCUUAGACAGUCUCACUCCUGCUGGACUGUAAACUCCUGGAGAACAGGGACAAAGCCUUGUUCAUUAGAGUAUUCCUAGUGCAUUCCACUAUAAUAGACACAUAAUUAAUACUUUUAAAAAAUGAACAAAUGAAUAAGACAUUUGUACAGAACUUGAGUGUUAGACCAGGUGGUUUCACAAAACAAAGCGCUCACGGAGGUUUAUUGGCCUUCCUCCUAUGUCUUUGACCUUUUCCUUAGCUUGUGUCUAUGCUGUGUUUCCUGUCUACGAGAUGGUGGAGAUGGCGAGCCCAGUUUUCUUUCAUCUUGAAAGGAUUCAGCUCCAUUACUUAAUAGUCCCAGUCAUGUUCCUUUCCCCCUAGAAUCUGUGUAUGAGAUGUGAAAUCCAUGAAAAGAUAAUGUUGAAUGGGAAAAAUUAACCUAUUUUGAUGACUUUUAAGGAGUUCUAACUGUGCAUGAUAGCAGGCGACUCCCUUGUCAGUAGGCAGCAGGCCUGUGUUAUGUCAGGGGUAACGAGGUGGUUCACUUGUGGAGAGUUUUCUGUCUUUUCUUCCAAGUUAUGCUGACCUCGCCGACGAAAAUAUUCCCCAUCUAAUAAAAGUCAGAGCAAAUUUAUGGGCCUGCCCCUGACCACUUGUCCUUUAUCCUUUAAAAGAAAAAAUAAAUCUAGGAUAAGAUCCAUAGGUUACUGUUGGACCAUGGAAAUGAUGGGCAGGGGCCAAAUAUCCCACCUUCCUUGAUCUGCUUCUCUUUUCCCGAUUCCGGCUGUCUGGGGGAUGCUGAAGCUUGUGGCAUGAGGGUUACUGCCGAGCAUGGCCAUGUCGUUAGUUCCCUUUGGAAACAAGCUGUUGCUCUCCCUGCCUGGAGGGCCACACGCCUUGGCACCACACUGAAGAGAUCCCAGGCGUGGCUGGAGUGAAGCUGCUAAUGAAAAAGCAGCCAUGGCAGGUCAGGACGAAUCAAGCAAAAAGGAGGACAUUCUAUAAUUAAAGAUUCAGAGAAAUACUAGCGCAGUUUUUGUUGUUGUUGUUGUUGUUUUGUUUUUUUGUUUUUGCCAACGCUAUGACAAUUGCUCUUUCUACCUGUUCCCGUGGGUUUUCUGUCAUUUUAUCACUCAUUAAACAAGUGUUUAUUAAAUCUCUACUUUCUGUGUGCUGCUUACCUGUGUGCUGUUGACCAUAGUUCAGGGAUUACUUAAAGCAUCAAUGAGUGUGCGAUGACUCAGGAAUGAGUCGGGUCCUCAAGGAUCUUGUCACCUAGUAAGAGACAGAGAAAUAUGAGGCAGAGGGAGGCUGGGCCAUAGGAUAUGGCAGGAUGCAGAGCAAAGAGCUCCAGAGUCUGAUAGACCUGGGAUCAAAUUCAGGCUCUACCACUUAUGAGCACAUUUGGCUUUGGGCAAUUUACUUAAUCUUGAACUUCAGUUUCUAAAUCUUUGAUUGUGCAUAAUACACAGCGUCCUGGAAGGGUUGUUUUAGGAUUUGAAAUAAGCUGUGAAAAGGGCCUGGCCUAGAGUUAGCACUUGACAAAUGGCUGCUCUUAUUAUUUUAUUAUCUCUGGCGAGGUGCUGAUAACCAUGUGAGUUCAGGGGAGGCAGUCUCCACCCCGUGGACAGAAGUGAGAGGAUCAGCAAGGGGAUCAGGAGUUUCAUGGGGCACAUGCCUCUGCACUGAGCUUGGGAGAAUGAGUAGGAUCUGGGAACGUCGUGAAGGAGAAUAGAGAAGAAACUUUAUUCAAGACAUAGGUUUUUACACAUUUUGUUUUGUUUUUAGCAAAUAGGCACUUAUUUUGCAUCAUUUUUAUUUGCAGUAUGCAAUCAAAUUGUGAGAUUACUUAAGCCUUAGCAUGAAUCCCAGUGCCAACAGUUGUGUAUUUCUUUCUUCUGCUUUCUUUUGUUGUCCCCCACAACCUUCUCUGAACAGCAUCUAUUAAGUGAUUGCAGAGUCUCAUGACUUGGUUGUGUUGGAAUCUCUGCAUUAGUGGGGACACCCUUCCAAUUCCUUGUUAGGAUCAAAUGUGUUUUAGAGAAGGUAUCUGGUUCCCAAGUUCUCUGUUGUUUUUUGGAACCAUGAAAGCCUAGAGAUGUUAUGGCAGGAUGUCCCUAAUAUGCAUGGCAAGCCCUCGACAAUGAUUAUGGCAGUUGUUACUAUUACUGAUUAUUUGUAACUUCUAAUAAUCCAGAAUUUAAAUUGGUCAAAGACACGCUGCUCCUCAGGGAGUCUGAAUAUACUGGUAUCAGCCCAGUGUCCUUCCACACUGGCCUGCAGCUCAUUGUGACUGGGCCAACUUUGGCCUUUGUGCCUGGCUUCUAUGCCAACCUGCCAAGUCCUUGAGAUGCUGUGCACCUUACUAUUUUUUGUCAGGCCUGCUAAGAAGGGGGCUUGUGUCCUGCAGAUCAAGGACCAAUAGGAAGCCCUCACCACAAACCUGAUUCACAGUACUCUCUCCUCUUUGCACUUUGCACUGAAGAAUCAUCCUCUCCUCCAUACACAUUUUUUCCCCAGUACAGAACUUAGCUUUGUGGUGCUGGGUUAUUAAGGAACCCAACUUGUAUCCACUGUAGUUGUAAUCUUGCUGGUCUUUGUCUGAGUUGCAAAACAACACUCAUGGAAGUCCUCAUUCAGUUAUUCUAGAGCACUUGUUGAGCUCCUGGUAGAGGCAGAGUGCUGUCCACCAGAUUUGUGCCUGAUGGCACAGAGAAUGAUCAAAAGGAAUCUUGCAACUGGACAUAGUUUCUUUAGACAGAGACAGAGGUAAGUAAGUAACCUCACAUAAGUAUCCUAACUCUUAUUUUCCAAAUGUUAAUGCUUGACUGGCAUGUUAUAAAGCUAAUUUGUUUAUAGUUGUGCCACAUAAUUAUACACUCUGUACAUAAUAUGCUUUUGAAAUUAUUAUUUAUUGCACAAAUAUUACAACAGAAACUGAACUCAAAACACAAGGAAAAAUGUGUGUGGGCUCACCAUUUGUACGAGUAAAACUUUUAAUAUAUUUGUGUGUUCACUCAUAGUCCUUAUCCAUGAAUUCAUAACUUUUGCACACAGUGGAAAUCAUACUGAAGAUACCAUUGGGUGUUCUGUUCUCCCCAUUCUCCUCUCCCCAUACACCAUAAUAUUAUUCAUGUAUGCUCUCAAGUUUAAUCAUGUCUGCAUGCGGACAUUUAGCUAUCCUUAGAGAGCCCAUAAUUUGAACUCUGAGCAUCUAGAGGAAGCUGCUGCCCCCAGCCCACUUAGGUACUUUCUUUUCCCCUUGUGGUGAGAAUAGGAAUUAGGUAGCAAGAGUUCCCAGGCUUCAUUGUCCAAGGCUAUGUUAGUAUUUUCAUCAUAAAUCUUGAGGCAUCGCCUAUUAAAGCCUUUUUGCCUUUCUCAUUAAAAGAAGAGAAUUUAGAAGGAAAUAUUUGAAAGACUCUAAGAUGCCCAGGAGAAAGGUUCCAACAUUAUUACUCUGAGUAGACCAAGUUAGGUGUGGGUAUAUAUUAAUAGUAACUAAACACCUAGCAGUUUGGUGUAUUCUGGAAUGCUCUUGACUUGGGCUGAAUGUGUCUGAUGCUCUAGGUGUUCUUGCUGUCUCUGUCUGUCAUCUGCCUGUCAUUCUCCUGUGAGGGUAAGUAGUAUCCCUUCCCAGACUGAGGAUGGAAAUGUUGAGGGGUGUAAAAUGAUAACUCAAACCUUUCCAAGAGUCCCCAAAGUGUGUACAGUGCAUAUGAAAUUCUCCAAAAGGAGAAGAGGGAUCUGGAAGUGCCACUGGGAGUGAGAGGCUGGGGAACCAGUGGAGUAGAGGAUAGUAGUGGCUUGAAGUCACAGAGCAAGAAUUCAAAACUUUGCUCUGGCACUAGCUUGGUGGCCUUGGGCAAAUUACUUAAUGUUUCUGAAUCUUUCCAUGAGGAAGAUAAUUACAUUGCCCACCUCACUUGGUUGUGGUCGGUAUUAAACUGGAUAAUGCAAAUAAUGCACUUAGCACAACACCUGGCAUAAAUAAUAAGCACUCAAUAAAUGUGAAAUGUUAUGGUUGUUAUUUCCUGCUUCACAUUAUAAUUUUAUUGCUUUCCAGACUGAUGUCUCCGAACUUAGGUAGUAGUGGAGUCUGUGAGCUAUUUUCAGUAUUUCAAAAUCUAUGAAAAGGAGACAGUUCUGGUCACCAUAAUAAGUACAUGACAGAUGGAGUCUUUGAAACAUGGUACCCACAGGGGAAGAAUCCAGAAGGGGUCCUUUGUGUUGAAAAGUUGAGGCCUCGAGCUGAGGAAGUUAGCAAGUGCUUCAGUGAAAGCUUGUGGGUUUCCAGUUACAAUGGGAGUAAAUAGAGGGAUGUUGUGAGCAAAGAACUUGAUUGGUUGCUAUGAGAGAUCGUUCCCCUGUGGAGCAUCAGAAGUUGAUGCACUCUGGAGACCCCAGUUGCUCUGUCAUGUUUACCAGUUUGUAGAAUGUGUUAUCACUGCCAAGCACCUUGGAAGCAGUGAGAAAACUGCCAGACAAAUGGAAACCGGUUUCUCUACCCAACUUGGUAGAACAUUUGCUCCAGGCAACCAUACAGGCUCCAGGAGACAUUUGCCUUGACAGUGCCUAUUUUGUAAAGCUGUAAUUUAAACUGACAAAACUUGAUUUUGACAUUGCAACAAGGUCUCUGUAGACUUAACACUAUGUUCAUUUUCCCAUGCUUAUCCCUACUGGAGACUGAUGGGUUUACACCAACAUGGAAGCUGGUUGGAAUGGAAACCAUCCAGAAAAUGAUUAGGGAGCUUGAAGCUCUCUGAAACUGGGCAUAAUGUGUAUUAAGUCAUUAUAGUUUUAAUGAAACUUGUCUUAGCUGGGGUCUCUUAACCACUUGUUUUCUAGUUGUAAAUAUUGAGUCCCUAAUUUACACUAAUGAGAUGCUGUUGAGAUUUAACGCCAAUCUUAUACUGCAUUUGUCAAAGUGUAAGAGCUAACCUGAAAUGUAGCUUUGCAAAAUAUUCUAUUAAAUAAACUUGGUGGAGAAGUAGCAACAAACAAACUGCAUGCUUUCAGCAGAAACUGUCAACAUACACAUCUCUGAAGAAAUUCAUAUUUUAUGCCAGGGUGGUCUACAGUAGUUCCCAUUAGUAAACGGUUAAAUAUCACCCUUCCCUGGUAAAUCUGAAUACUUUUGUGUCUGUUGUGAAAUGCUGUACACAUCCUCUUUUGAUGAUCUGCCUGGGAAUUCUCCACUGUGAGAAUUGUCUCUUAAAAAUGGGAAGCAGCAAGGCAUAGUAGAAAGAAUAUAGGCACUGGUGACACAUAUAUUUAGGCCUGAGCCCAGCUCCCAGUUGGUGGCCAGGUAAGUUCUUUAACCUCCUUUUGCUUAUUUUUUUUUUCUCCCUGCAACAUGGGGUUGGUAGUACUUAUAGGGCAGUGCUAUCCAAACACUUAGUAGAGGUGAUAAUGUAAGUAGUGAACGUAGCUCCUGACAUAUAGUUGGUGUUCCCUAAAGGAUAGAUUGAAAGAUAUACACACCACCAAGUUGAAUUCCUCUCAGAUUUGUCCAAGGCCACCCAGCCUUUCUUGGCCUUUUCUUCCAUCAUUGGUUAGUGUGUGUUCUUGAAGGCAGUCUGAUUUUAUCCUUGGCUUAAAAAGUGGGGAAAUAUUUAGGAAGCCUAGCCUAAUGCAAGAGAACUCAUCUAUCUUACUGUAGGAUCAAAUACAAAUGGUUUUUGGAUUGUCCAUUAUUUAUCUCUCACUUCUCUUCAUUAGUGGUGCUAAUGGAAACACAAUUAUCUUCAUAGACUUUGUUAGUCACAAUCUCUUGGUUUCUUCAAAUCCCACAAUAGCAAGAAUAUGUUGUGGUUUUUAUAAUCUCUUUUGGUUCCUCAAACCCAAAGAAGGACAGUGAGAGGGUGGGAGAUGAUUUGAGAGGGUAUUUACAUUCCCAGGAUUUUCAGAUAUAUUUAUGAUUUUAUUUUUUUGGAGACAGUGUUCCAAUAGAGAGGUAUUCUGUCUUCUCUUUUCUUUUUUCUCUUCUCUCUCCUCCCCCCAAAUCGAGGUUGUAAGUGAUGUGAGAGACCUGCUGUGAACUGCUGUCACCAGAUCCUGCUAUGAUUUCUCUUUGUUCUUAGUUCUGGAGUCAUCAAGGCUACAUGGAGACACGUACCUUCCACUGAUAUGUUUGCUCCUUGAUUCAGGGCUGAGUGCCUGUUUGAGUGAUUCUGGCUACAGCUAAAUGAUAUUUCUGUUUCCAAUAGUAUUGUAAACUAUAGAGUAAGAAUUUUCUUGUUGUUGUUGGGAGAGUUUGUUUUUCUUCUUAGUGUGUAUUAUCUCCCACCCCACUCCUCCAACCCGUUCUUUAAAAAACAAAACAAAACCAACAAACAAAAACUUGCAUUGAAGCAACACCCAGAAGGAGUGAGCAGGCCUAGGCUGGAGUCUUAUCCUGACAUGGUAGAAUCCUGUUACUGUCUCUUCGUAGAUUCAUUUAAAUUGUUUUGACUGAUUCAUGCAAUCUCUCAGUCCAUUGAUCAAGUCAAAAGAAAAAGUAUCACUAAAAACUCACAGGACUGGUGCAGGUAGAAUAUUCUUUAUCUAUGGAAAAUUCAUUAUCCUAUCUAGAAGGAUGUCUUGAAAUAGCAGAAUAUUUUUAUUAUGUUUUUUUUCCAAGUAAUACAUGGUUCAAGAAAAAAGAAAUUUUAAAAAGCCACACUAAUAGCAAAACUAAAAUAAGCAUGAAUCUUAAUUUUAACAAAGAUUACAGUAGUCCAUGGGAAGGAUUGUCUGCCCAUUGCAGUGGGUUUGAUUGGUUUUUUUACUUGGAAGUGCUCAUAUUCUGGAAUGUGUUUAUAGAUCUUGACCUUAGAUACUUCUCCUGACUCAGAAAUUGUAAAAUGUUUUGCUAGAGUAGCCAGUGGUGAGAGACCGCUACUGCUGUAUGUUGCUCAGGGCUAACCUGUUAAGAACUGGUCUCGUCGCUCAGAGAGAACCAUGAUGCUGAUGCCAGUUUCUUGUUUAUGUAAAAACAUUUAAAAAUGGGCAAGAUACUCUCUAAGUACAAGAUAGUUAUUAUUGAGAUAUGUUCAUGAAUAAAUUAAUGAGAGAGGAACUUGAGAUAAAGGAAAUGGAGGAGAGAAAUUGCAUUUUUCCUGCAUAAUUACUCUCUUGUUUUAGAACACAAGUAGUCCUUUGGCAUAUUUUCAAAGUGUGGUAUGUUUCACUUUUGUUUAAACUUGUCAAAUUCUCAAUGUAAAAGCCAUUUAAGACUUUUUUUUCCUUCUUUUUUGAAGGUUGCUUCUUUUGGCCUCUUAAAGAUAAUUAAGAGCUGUAAUUUGUGAGGAUUUUGAUGGCAUUUUUUGGCAGUGGUAGUGCAGGACAGGAUACAUGAAUCAUAGCAUCUGCUUAUUAGCAAGGUCUCAUAGAUCACUUGUCCAACUUUCCACCGGGUGCUGAGAUGGUUGGUCUCUGUUAUCUGUUCUUCCCACUUCUGCUGGAUACAUUCUGGGAAAAGAAUUUCAUUGAUGAGUGAGCUGUACUUCCACUUCUGAAGUACAAAAGUUAUUAAGCUAGGGAGCAUUUUCUCCAUUUGACACCUACAGGCCACUCAGUAAAAAAGCAAAUGAAUGAUGAAUGAGUAAGGUCCCUGGGCUGCUUCCUACUUCUUCUUAGAGUGGUUAAGGCCCUCUUGACAUUUUUGGAGGAUGAUAAAUGUGUGCCCUUGAAGUUUCCUUGUCCAGGUCAAACAGCCCCAAUUUCUCCAUGAUCUUUGGACAUUGCUUCCACAUUUUCUCUCCUUCUUGCUCUCCACAGGGCAAGUUUCAUUUCAUCAAUUUUUUUUUGUAAAAUACUGUAAAGAUAUCUGAAUGAAGUAGACCAGGUAUAAUCUGAUAAGCAUAGAGUAUGGUGGAGCAUUUCUUUUAAGGUUCUGGGUAUUGUUAUUAUCCUACUAAUGGAACCAGCAUUUGCUGGACCUUUUGGGGCCACCAUGCCUUAGACAGGUAGAUAAUGGAAUGGCAUAGAGAACAGCCUGAAGCCGGCUGUCUUGGUUUGAAUUCAGACUUACCAUUUAUGAAAUGUUUGACCCUAGGCAAGUUGUUUAACCUCUCUGUAAACUUGUCUUCAUUUGUAAAGUCAGGGGUAAUCAUAGUACUUAUUUAUACAGUUAUUAUAAGGAGUAAAUAAAUUAGUUUGUGCUGAGUGCCUACAACAAUGCCUGGAGUGAAAUAAGCACUCUGUGUUAGCUUUUAUUGAAUUUACAAUGAAAAACGUCCAGGUCUUACUAUCUGAAGUGCAGUUAGUUUUUUCAGCAAGGCUUUAGAAUUAGACAGGGCUAUGUUUAAAUCUUAGCUCUGCUGUGUGUUUUGGGGGAAAUUACUUUGCCUUUCUAAGCUUCUGUUUCCUCGUCUGUGAAAAGGGCAUUAAAGAAUAAAAUCAGUUGAAUUUCUGAGCCCUAAUUAAGAACCUUGAGGGCAGAGCCAUGGUUUACACUUGCUUUUUUUCUUCUUUCUUAACUUUACCUGGUAUGCCAUGUUUAUAAUCACUGCUAAAUUAAAAUAGUAAAUAUUUAAACUGAGUUUUCCCUUCAGUCUACCUUGUAGUAGAAAAAUUAAAUACUUCUAUGUUACUUAAAACUGCACACUCACAAGUUUAUGGUGGUGUAUUGAUUGGUUGUUCUGAAGAAUGUAUUCUGCUUGCCACCAUGAACUGGGCUUCAGAAUAAAUAGGCUUCCUUGAUCACUUCUCUCCUCAUUAACUACUGUCUGGAAUUUAGAGGGAAUACAAAGUCUGGUAGCUACAUUGCCUACUAAUCUUGCAAAUGGCCUGUGAGGUGGGUAAGCAAUCAGGUGAGUGACAAAGGUUAUAGUCAAUUUUCCUGGCACUCUGGGAUUUAUUUUUGUGUCCUUGAAGUUUUAAGCAAGUGAGUUUUGAGGUUGUUGAGAAAGUGGGAGACUAUAUUUUAAAAUGGUUUAUAGUUAUUAAUGUUUUCAAAUCUUGGUGGGAUUUUAAAGGUGGGUUAAGCUGCGAAAGUGAAUGUAAGUUAAAGCCAGUUAAAUAGAGGAGUCCCUCGUUCAUUCUGUCUUUGGUAUGCUUAGGAUUUCAUAAAUUUUAUGGGUUUCAAAAUCUUUGCCUUGUUUUGAAUGUUUCUAAUAAGAUGGAGUGAAGUGGCUUACACCUCAUGAGACAUGGAACAGUUAUCCAGGAAUGCUGCUUGGCACACAUAUAAAGAAAGCACUGGUCUAUUGAUUCAUAAAAAAUGUGUGACUGAUUUUCCUGGGACAUGUGCAUUAUUUUCACAGAAGAAUUUCAUUUUUUACUUCCUCCCACCCUGUGCAUCACUUGCACACGUUUGCAAUUCAUCAACUCUGAUUUCCAAAACUUCUGCCCCCUCUUCCCCCAACCACCUCCAUCCAACUACCUAAAGUGAAAUAUAUUAGAUGGAGAGGAGGGAAAUUUCCUUAAAUGCCUAAUUUUUAUGUCUGUAAGGGGCAUGGUGAAUUUGAGAAAUGGUCUGAAUGUUAGCCCAGAUGACUCAAUGCAAUUAUGAAACAAAUUGGAAGCUGUUUCCAUGAAAGAGUAUGUAUGCAUGUGUUUCCACGAAAGGGGUGUGUGUGUGUGUGUGUGUGUGUGUGUGUGUGUGUGCGCGUGUGUGUGUGAGAACAUGUGUUUAGGUCAGUUCUUUCAUUCGUUCUCUUUCUUCCUCUUCUUUUUGUCGUUUCAAGGCUAUGUUUUAGGUUGGCUAUACAGCAAUGAGGUUGCACUACACAGCCUCAUCCCCUAAAGCCAAAAUACAGCAAGUAGAAGACUGCUUAGCUCAUCCAGUGAGAAUCUCAUGUAUUAUAUUCUUACUUGCCAUUGAGUUGCCAGAAAAAAAAUAAAUAGCUUUGUCUUAGAAAGCAAUAACUUUUCUGCAAUGAAAUAACAUUAAACAACUCUACCUGGUAUGCCAUGUGCAUUGUUUUUCCUUUCUUGGAAAGGAAAAACUUUCUUAGAAAACGAGGGCACACAAUGAUUAGCGCUAACUUUCUCUUUCAUGUGUCCAACUUAAGAUUUUCUAGUGAGGCAGAGUUAUUUCCCCUUACAUGCUUGGUUUAAUGGAAAGGGCCUGGCUUUCAGUUUUGUUCAUAUUCAGCUACCAAGACCCAAUCAGUUAAUAACUUUGCCCAGAGUUGAAAGAAAAAUUCCUCUGGGUACAGAGUUAAAUUCCUCUGCGUGUGGAAGGCCAUAGUGGUUAAAAAGUUAGGCUUCGGAGCCAGAUCAACAUAGAUUCAGAUGUGCCUCUGCUGCUCAAUGUGUGAUGAGGGCAAAUUGCUGAACUCAAGUCUCAAGUUUCCUCAUCUGUCUGAUGGGGAUCAUAACGCACAUCACCUGACGUUGUAAUAAUUGCCUGACAAUGUGUAUAAGGCACUCGUGUAAGAUCUGGCACUUGGCAAGAGUAAAAUGCAUUUUAGCCUAUACUUUUUACUCUUCAUUUGUAAAAUUGUGGUAAAGGGAUUGGCCCUGGAGGGAGUAGGGUGAGGUGGCAUUUUCAGGAAGGUAGCACAAGGUUACAGGGAGGACAAUAGAAAUGUACAGGAUGGCUGAAGACUCAGUAAGUAAAUAGCAUUGCUUCUUACAGCAGGCCGGAGGAGAUCUCUAUAUUUUUCUUUAUUAGAGAAAAUUUAAGGGAUAUUGAUUUUUAAAGGGAAGAUUUAUAUUUUAAUUUUAAAGAGGAAAAUUUAUCAGCUCCUAUAUAUUUAUUAGACAUUUUGGGGGGGAAACAGUGAAUGAAUGAGACUGGUCCCAUUUGAUGUAUGCUGUCAAAGUUUAUAAACUAUCUGAUGAAUUAGUAAGAACAUAUCAAACAAGACAAAGAGGCUCAUUGUUAAUGUGCGCAGGUGAGGCUUUGCAGGCUGCUUGUGGGUGAGGGUAAAAGUUUUCUUAACCUCAAGCCUGGAUUCUGACCAUAGAAACAUUCCUCCUGAGUGAGUAGUGCUUCUAGAGUGCUUUCCUUCAAGGACCUCUCCGGCAUCUGGCUCAAUCACAUGCCAUCUUUUUCUCCUUUACAUCUGCUUCCUUGCCCCACUUUGGCACCCAGCUAAGUGUGGGCAGAUGGUGUGGCCUUGGGGACUCCAGAAGGGCCUUGGUGUCCUUCAGUAGCAUGGAGUGUAUAGCAGGGUCUGCCCGUGAAGGACCAGGGAGGUGAAGGGCCUUACAGGACUCAUGUGGAAUGCUUGUGAAUGCAUUAUUUCCAAAUAUCCCUGAGUAUUUGCAAGCGUUUUUAUAUACCUUUACUUCCAUUUUGCUUUGACAACACCAUUACCAUUCCUUGACGAUGAGGAACUGAUCGGAAAUAAACCUAAUUGUUAUUUGCUUAACAGUUUCAAGACCUGCAACUUGCAGCAGUCUCCUGACGGUCUCUGUACAUUUUCUCUGUCCCCUUCUAAUCUAUUCACCACAUUGUAGCUGGAGUGAUUUUUUUUUUUUUAAACAGAAAUCUGAUCAUGAGCUUUCUUGGUUUAAAACUCCUUCACGGCUGCCAUUUGCUUACAGGUUUAGGGCUGAAAUCCUUGCCAUGGCUUGGCUUACAGGACUCUGUGGGUCUAGCCUCUGCUGACUUUGCUCCUCAGCACCAACCUAUUCAUCUUUCAUCCUUCCCUCUUUCCAGAAAACCUAAAGGUGGAGCCCUGUCUGCUCCAUCUGCUGCCCUGGUUACUCUCAUCCAGGGCAUUCAUUCUCUUUUUAUAAGUACUGUGAGGCCUUUUCACAAUUUGUUACUACUGCAUAGUUAUGUACUUAUUUCUUGCCAGUCUCCCUCACAAGGCUGCAAACUUCAGGAGAGUGCAGACCGCAGCCUGUUCAGUCCUCAUGGUAUAUGAAGCCUGUUGCAUUACAGGUCCUGAGCCUCCAUUUGUUGAAUAAUUUCAUUAAUUAAUUAACCAAUUAAUUAAUUUCCUCUAAAGGGUUUGAAACCCCAACUAUUAAGGCUUAUGUUGAAAGGACAAUUUAAAGGAAAAUAAACUGUUAGAAGAGGGAGAGAUAGAAGCCCCAGAAACUUGGAAUGAGUCAGAUCUUACAGCUGAGCAGGAACGCAAGCUUUGAGGAAAGCUUUAUUUAUUUAAAUAGGAGUCUCAUAAGGAAGGCAGAAAAAGGAAACCCAAGCAGAUGACUUGGUUCCUAUUAUCUGCUGAGAGGAAGCUCAUCUGGAGUGAUGACUUUUUCCUGGCACUAAAUUUGACCUGAAAAUUAUAAAAUGAAUCCAUACAGAAUAAAAAAUACCCUCCUGCUCCCAUUAUGGAUGAUGUCUUCUAUUGUAGUUUGCCGAAGGGACAGAGUUUGUGAGAGGGAGUGAGUUGAGAUGAGGUGGAGAUGAAAGCCUGUAUAUAAUUUAGAGAGAACUUGGGGCAAACUAGAAAGAUAGCCUGUGGUCUGAGAUGAGGGCCGAUGCCACAGACAUGGGGACCCCUUUCCUUUCUGGCAGCAUUUUCCUGUGUGUAUUCUGGGGGGCCUUCAAGGUAUUCUGUGACAAAAGGGUUCUCUAGUCAGAUAGGUUUGCAAAACACUGCGUAUUAUAUCCUGGCCCACCCUUGAAGUUGUAUAAUGCAUACCAAUAAAUAAAGACCCUGAGAAGUGAGAGUCUUAUAGUGAAGAGAUGUUUAGCUGUUUAAUCCACCAUUUUUCAAGCUUAUUUGACCUCAGAAAACAUAAUCAUAGAACUUCCCUCAAAACAGACCUGAGUAAUGCUAAUUUAGGAGUUGGAGAGAACAAGAAGUACCAGCAUGAGAUCAAGGUAGAGAAACUCAAUUAUCUUUGUAGAAACAUUUCUACUUUGAAAUAGAAAUAGAAUGAUCUAAGCUGAAAUAGAUUUUUUUGUGUGUGUUUUAUUAUAGUAGUGGUUGGAGUAGGGGUCCCCAAAAAGUAAGGAUUAAGGGAGUGAGGAUCUUUCCUUUAUGAAAAUGGUAUGGACCCGUGUCAUUUAAUGGAGGGUUUUGGUGGUUAGGAGGACAGGCUACUGGGUGUGAGUUCAGGGUCUACCAUGUUUUAGCUGGAUGACAUAAGAAAUUGCCUACCAUCACAGUGCCUCCUUCCUCACCUGUGAAAUGUGGGUAAUAAUAGUAAUGACUACAAGAGCUCUUCUAAGAAUUAAAUGUGAUGAUGCAUGUAUAAUGCUGAGAACAGUGCCUGGUUCAAAGUAAGAGCUUAAUAAAUGUUAGCUAUUAGUAUUGCUGAUUAAAGAAUGCCAAGGAAUUAAUAAGCAUGGAAAGAUUGGAGCCCUUUACUCAGAGCAAAAUCUAGAAAUGUCUAAUAGCCAAAAUAUUCUUCUCAUGGGGCCUUUUCCAGCUUGAGGCAAAUGAUAAUAUGUUUAGAAGCUGAUGGGGUAAUAGUUUCCCAGCUGGAGAAAAACCUGAGUCUUCAUACAAGGAGAGAGAACCACAAUGUGUGUUCCUGCAGUACUGCUGUGGAAGUCAUGCUGUAUGCAAGUACGUCCAAAUCAAUAAUCAUAAGUAGCCCCGAUGGCUGAACCCAAAGUCUUUCUUUAUAAUCUUUUAUAUUAUUUCUUUAAAAGACUCUGCCUGUAAAAGAAUCUGAAUCUAGUAAACUUACUCGUGAUUUAAUUUGAGCUCUGUUUGAGGUGUUGGCUCUGUUUGUUGAUUAUGCCAGGUUCUUUUCGGUUUCUAAGCAGUUGAAUCAAGUGAUAGAAUGUCUGGUUUUCUAGUUGCUUCAUACAUGAAGUUGCAUAUCCAUCCAUCUAUCCAUCUAUCCUUCCAUCCAUCCAUCCAUCCACGCAGUAAAUAUUUAUCAGUCAAGUACUACUAACCACUUCCAAUUUAUGAAGCAUCCUCACAAAGCCCCCAAAUGUGGUUUAAAUAUAGCACUAGGAAUUCUUUAGGCCUCUGAAAGUUACUUAUGAAAAUGACGGAGACUGUUCUGUCUUAUUUUCUUAUCCUCCUAAUUUACAAGUUCUGUUCUGUGUACACUGUGACUCUGUAAGAGUAGUGUUGGAGACUAGAUUAAAUGUAGAUCUAAAAUACCCUGUCCAUAGGCAGAGAUAGGUAAAGAAUGGCUAAUUACUAAAUAAUUAAUAAUAGCUGGUGAUGCUGCUGGCCCUUAUUUGACCUUUACAUAAGCACAGCUGCCUCUGGGCUCAUCCCAGGGGCUAUCUUUAUCAACACUAGAGUGUGAUAAUAAAUGAGUUUCUCUAGGAAUUUUUCUUUUUGUUCAGGCACUGUCUCUGAAGAGUGUUCCAUGGGAAAACAAUCCUCAUGAUAUACAUUUUUUUAAUAGAUAAAACUUUGGCAGAUCCAUUUUCAACCCUGGCAUUCAGACCUCCUAAAAUUGCUAUCAGCUAAUAGAGAUUUAGGAUAUAGAAAGCUGGGAAGGCAGUCAAAUUGGUUCCCGGCCACUAAGGCCCUGCAUGCAUAAGUAUCACAUGAGGGCUAUGGACACCAAGACCAAUCAGGCCAGGCUUUUCAGGAAGCUCUGCUCAGAAUCAGGUGGAGAACAUUCUUAAGCAGUAGUCAAUUAUUAUUCUUGAAUAUUAAUCACAAUUAGUGCAAAAGACUACCUCUUGCCACUACCAGAAUUAUUUUGUAUAUAGAGAUCUUAUAUGAGCAUGGGAAAAUUUAUUUUUUAAAUGCUACUCUCUGGGAAACAAAGUCAUUCACUCACCAGGUGUUUAUUGAGUUAAUUUUACGCCAGACACUUUGCUAGGCCUAGUGAUACAAGGUGAAUGAGGCAUGGCAUUGCCCCUAAGGAAAUAUAAAAUAGUAUAGAGUUUCAACUUAAGUGUCAGAUCCAAUCUAUUAAUUGGUAGUGGCUGCCUGGAGGAUUGUGUUGGGGAGAAUUCUGAGGCUUUGUCUGGACACAGUGAUUGAUUAGAACAAUCUUCCUUGAGGAUAGAAAGGGGAUAAUGGUAGAUGUACCACCCAUUUUCUGUACCUAGUCUUCUGAGAGACCGGCAGGCAGUUGCAGCUCCAUAUGUUAGGUACUAUAGGAGGGGAUCAUAUAGGAUACUCUGGGAACACCUAAUUCUGCACAUGGAGCAGAAAAUAGCAUCACAGGCGGUUGAAACUUUGAACUGAGACCUGAAAAUUAGUAGGAGAUCCCCCCCGGUGAAUAAACAAGAGAAGUGCAUUUUAGGCAAAGAAGCAAAGUUGGACCUGGAAGCAAGCAAUGGUAGGAUGUGUUGGGAAAGGCAAAUUGUUCUUUGUACUGGGAAACUUUGCCAAGACCAGAUCUCACUGAAGGAUUUGGAUGUUAGGCCCAGGAGCCUUGGAGGACUGUGAGACAACACUAAAAAAAUACCGAUCCUUGAAAAAUAUUAAUCUGAAAAGAAGGCACUGAUGGCAGGCACCCUUUAGAGCUCUGGCCUCUGGUCUGUUCUGUUCAACCUCUAUACUGAUGGCUUGGUUAGACAAAGAUGACGUGCAUGUUGAUCAGAUUAAUAGAAGACACAAUGUUUGGAAGUUUUGUGAGCCUGUGGGUGACUUAAUCUGAAACCAGAUGUCUCAAACAGCUUGAACAAUUCCAAACCAGAGGAUAUUUGCUAGGGAAAAUAUAAAUUCUGUACUCUGGCUGAAACAACCAAUUGUACAAGAGCAGGAUGGAAGAAUAUUUAGCCUGGCAAUAAUAUGUGUGACAAGAGUUAGAUUUUGGUUACAAAUGUCACCAGUCUACAAUGUGACAUGUCCACACUGAGAAAAUAGUAAUGAUGGGCAUGAAGAGUUCUAAAAAAGUUCUAAUCAUCCUGUCUCCUUCUGUCAUGGGCCUACUACAAAAGGAGUGUUCAUUUUGGUAAAGAUGUUAAGAUAAAAAUUAGCUGGCAUGAGUCCAGAGGAAAACAUCUAGGCUGAGGAGAUAUUUUGGUUGAUGAUUUUAGGGUUACUAAACCCAGAAAGAGAAAAUUAAGGACUGUCUUCAAAUAUUUUGAAGAUAAUCAGUAGCCUAGCACUUAGGCUUAUGUUGUAUGGAGUGAUGAAAAAUGGGUAGACAUUUCUGGAAAGCAAAUUUCAGCUCAGGUUCUCAAUGAAGCCUCCAAUGAUGGGAGCUUCUUUGAAGUGGAAAGGGCAAAUAAUAAGUUUCCUGUCCGAGAAGUGAGGAUGCAGAGAAUGGGUUAACACUUGUUGGAAAGAUUGUAGAAGGGAUUUAUGUAUUAGAUAUUGUUUGGGCUCAAAGGUCCUUCCAACUCUGAGAUUUUUUUCAUUCUAGAGGAAAAAAAAUAUCCCUACACUGUACUGUCUUUGAAGCCAGAAAAAGAACAUCUAUAAAUUUGAGCCCAACCUUUAAGUUGUGUCUCUUGUUGGGGCAGGUUUCUUGACUUGCUGUGAUGACAGUGGAGCCUUUCUAUCCCUCAUCUGGACUUUACUUGUAAUCUUAAAAGUCCUCUCUCUCUCUUUUUAUUUUUUUAACAUCUCCUUCCUCUGUUUUCUGGGCCACUCACUCAAAGACACCCCAUAAAAUAUUUGCCCGGGAAAGAAGGCACCUUCCAAUAAAAAUACCUAUAACCUGGAGGACAAGACACAAAAGCCUUAUUUCUCAGCUCUGAGCUUUUGUUAAAACCUGUGUUAUGACUGGGUGAAAUGAGCUGGCCUCAGAGAACAGGCCAGAAAACACAGGGAAUCCUUUGGCUGAUUGGCAUCCUCUGCCAUUGGUGACUCUCCAUAACCCAUGUUGUUGUCUCUGGCCGCCAGCACCCCAUCAGAUGUUUUGCCAGCUUGAGUUCUGAGUCUGAUUUCUCAUGCCAGCUUCAUCUUGGUGUUGCUGAAUAAAGGAGUUUCCCACCAUCACGAUACACCUUCCCCUGCCCCUAGGAGAAAUCUUCCUCCAGAGGGAUGGGCAGCCAUGUGGCUAAAUGGGUUCCUGCUCAGAGGCGAGGAGGUGAGGAAGAACACAGUGCAUGUGCUGAGCAGAGAUCCAGCUCCUACUCCUGGUUUCUUCCAAAACCUGCCUGUUAAUCACCUGUUUACAUUGCCAAGCAUGCUUGACUGGGUAAUGAUAGUAGGGGGAAAAGCAGUGAAAGGAACAUCACAGGUUUUACUCAAGUGGAGUAAUCCCUUCCUGAUUUACAGGCAUUUCGGUGGCUUUGGUGCAGACAGAGUGGCUGGUCUCAUUCUUUUCACACCAAUGGCCAGCAGCCCCCAGAAAGCAGUUGGACUCUUCGUACCCCUUUGAUGUCCCCUCUUGGGUGAUUCCCACGUGGAGGGUGGUGCCACUGGGCUUGGUUGCAGUCUGCCACCCCACCUUCCCAGUUAGCAUUCCCACCUGCUGUUCCUGGUGACUCUUGGUAAAGUCAGACUGUUGGUGCCUGCACUUGUGGGUGUUAUGUGAGGGACACAUGGAGACCAGUUUGCUGUAGUCUCUUCUCUCACUGGCCUGCCCCGGUGCCAUGAUCUGAGGAUACCACAGCUGAAAGGGAACUCAGAGGUCAUCAAGCCUGACCCCUUUCAUUUUGGCAAUGAGGAAACAAAGGACUAAAGAGGUGAAGGAAAUUGCUCAAGGUCACGCAGCUAGUUGGUGACAGGGACUGCAGCCUCAGCCUUUUGAUUCAUAAACCAGGGAUCCUUUUUCUCUCCUAGGUUAAAGCAUUGCCCUUUUUUAAAUGAAUAUAUUUAUUUAUUCAGAAAUUCAGCAAAUAUUUAUUGAACUGUGACAGAGAUGAAUAAAGUCUGUCUCCACAAACAACUCAUAGACCUGGGGAGGAGACAGGGGAUUAUACAAAUUAACUCAAUGUGGAAAGUGCUGGUAAAUGGAGGUAAGAAUAGAAGGCUAUUCUUUCCCUUCUCCGGGAAAAGUGCCUGACUUGUGUUUUGGUUAUGGUGUGUUUUUUUUUUUGAGGAGAGUCAGAAAAGGCACCAAGGUAACCUGGAGACAUAAAAUAGCAUAGUGACCCAGGAAAUGGGCUCUGGAACCAGACUGCCUUCAUGUGAAUCCAAGCGCUGCUGCUCACCUGCUGAGUAACUCUGGGCAAGUUGCUUUUUGUGUCUCUAAUUUCCACUCUAAAAAUGUGAGGAAAUUGAUAAUACUUAUCUCCUAGAUUUAUUGUAGGAGUUCAGUGGGUUAAUACAUGGAAAACACUUUAAAAGUGUAUUGGCAUAUAGAAAAAAACAUAAUAGCUAUCAUUAUUAUUAUUAUUUCAAGAGCUGUAUUUGAAUAGUAUGCUGAGUAAUGAGACAGAUCCUUAUGUUUCAAUGGUGACCAAAGAUUUAGAAAUGUUAGCAUAGUUGCCAGUGAAAGAUGCUGGUUUUGCUUGGGGCUCCUAGGGAAACCAGGCACGUAGAUGGGAAUGGACGGGUACAGUCUGGAAGCAGUGGAUGAGAAGGGAUUUGGGGAAGAAGAAAGCCAGAAGGCUAGCAUUUCUUUUUUCCUUCAUGGUUUUAUCUAAGUUGGGGCCACAGAGGGGUGAAUAUUGUUCUGUUGAACAAACAGGGGGAUAUGGCAGUGUCUGGGGCUUUGGGGGAUCAGUGGUGGUUUCUGGGUAUGGCUUUUGUUCUGAAGGAGCUUCCUUCCAGAAGUGGGGACGUGUGCCCACAGAUGCCUGUGCCCUGAAGAGGUGCAACAACGAGGUUUCUCUUUUGGGAAAGAGGAGAGAGACCAGUAUCUUAAGAUGUUGUCAUCUGGUUCCAAUUUUCUCUCCUCACCUCUUUAGCAUCUCUUACCUAAUUAUUUGCUUCCUGAAAGCAUUUUUCUCCCAAGAGUAGGUGCCCAGAGAUGCCCUUGGGUAUAGGAUCAAUGCAACCGAGCAGAUUGAUUCCUCCAAACGUGAACCCUCAUAUGUUAGAUCAGUGGUCCCCAACCUUUUUGGCACCAGGGACUAGUUUCAUGAAAGGUAGUUCUUCCACAGUGGUGGGGGGAUGCUUUUGGAAUGAUCCAAGCACAUUACGUUUAUUUUGCACUCUCUAUUAUUAUUACAUUGUAGUAAAUAAUGAAAUAAUUACACAACUCACCAUAAUGUAGAAUCGGUGGGAGCCCUGAGCUUGUUUUCCCACAACUAGAUGAUCCCAUCUGGGGUGAUGGGAGACAGUGUCAGAUCAUCAGACAUUAGAUUCUCAUAAGGAGCAUGCAACCUAGAUCCCUCGCAUGCGCAGUUCACAGUAGAGUUCACGCUCCUAUGAGAAUCUAAUGCCAUCGCUGGCUGAUCUGACAGGAAGUGGAGCUCAGGUGGUGAUGUGAGCGAUGAGGAGUGGCUAUAAAUACAGAUGAAGCUUUGGUCACUCUCCCACCGCUCACCUCCUGCUGUGCAACCCCGUUCCUAACAGGCCAUGGACUAGUACUAGUCGUGGCCCUGGAAGCUGGGGACCCCUGUGUUAGACCAUUUCAUAUGGGCUGCAUUCUUUUUUGGAAAAUGAGGUGGUUGCAAUGCAUGGUUCUUAAGGUCCCUUCUUAGCACAAACAUUCUUGUUCUUGGGCCCUGGUAUUAUGGAUAUUAUACACAUGGUUUUUGCUACUUGCCAGGGAUCCGGGAAGGUCUGUGGCACCCGGUAAUUUAUAAUUCUGCUGAGGCAAGGAUUUGGCCAGAAGGAGUCACAUGGCUGGUGAGUCAACUUAGCUGAUCACCCAAUCUCCACACUCAGUUCCUGGCACUUACUAACUGAGGUUGCAAAGGUCUCUGCAUCUUCUCCUUCAGAAUGUUGAAGGUUGGCUGCUACAUCAUUUUCCCUUAGAUUUAGAGAAGAAAAGUUUUUCUACUAGAGCUCAUAUUUCUCUCUUCUUCCAUAGCGGCUUUUAUUUAAACUAUUAGGAGAGAAAACCCUCCAUACUCGACCACCCACCUCCACACUGGCACAAAUCCAGCCUAAAUCAGAACCGUCAGCUCACCCUGAGCCGGGCUGUGGACUUUUCUUCCAGGCAGGUGGGAUAGGAAUGGGAGUUGAAGUUUGAGCAACUUUUGAAUUAUUGCAGUUACCUGGAUAUAUGAUGUUUUUCUGCUGUGUAUAAAGUGGGCUAGAAGGAUCCUCACUCUUCCACACUCUGUCCUCCUCCCAAAAGAAUUUCCUAUUUGUUCAAGGUGCAGGAUUGACAGCCCAGGAGACCUUGUGUCUCCACCUGGGCAGGUCAGACCAUGGCCUAUGUGGGUGGCUUGCAGCAUGUCUGUGGAAAGUGGGCACAGACCACCUUUGAGGGACAAAGGGGCGGUUGUCUGAGGGCCCCUUUAGGAGCUCACCUUCCUUUGCCCUACUAUUUCCUGUUUUGUUUUGCGUUUUGGGAUGGGGGGGUUUGGGGAUGUAUAGGCCAUGCUUGUUCACCCUGAGUUGCUGUCCUUUCUUCCCAUAACAAUGUCUGAAGAAAGAAGAGGAGGGUGGGCUUGAAAUUGUGAUGGGGCUAAUGCUUAUUUUGAAUACAUGAGGUAAUUUUUUGGGUUUUUGUUUACUUUAUUCUUGCUGUUGAGGUAUAAUUAAUAUAGAUGAAUUAUGUGUUUGGUUCCAUCAGUCUUAAUAGUCAUGUCCACUCAUGAAACUACCUAAAGCAAGCUAUAGAACAUUUGCGUUAUUUCAGAAAGUUCCCUUGUGCUCCUUUCUAGUCAAUUGUACUACCCUGCCUCCCAUCCCUACUCCCACACCUCUACCCAGAGGCAAUCACUUUCUGGCUUCUAUCACCAUAGUUUAUACACAGGGUAAUUUUAAAAAGCGUGUAUUCACUGCAACCUGUGUAAAUCCAAAAAGGGUUACAGUUCUUUGGGGACUGUUUUUAAAAAAAUCAGAAGGCUGGAGCUAGAAGCAGCUUUCUCCCAUACCUUGAACAAAUCUUUGACAAUGAUGGGCCUAGGUGACCUGAUCUCUAAAACAAUUAUAAUAAUAAUUCCUACCACAUAGCAGAAAAUGAUAAUAAUAGCUGCAUACUGUUAUUGACCACUUCACUCUUCUGAACAUUUUACUUCAUUAUCUUAUUUAAUCUUCAGAAUGACACCUUGAGAUGUGUACCAUUUUUUCUAUUUUAACACAUGGCGAAACCAGAGCUUUCAGAGGGGAAGUAACUUGCUUAGGGCCACAGAGCAGUCAGUCAUAAUUCAAAUCAGGAGCCUUUGUGUCCAGGGCUUUAACCUAGAGCAGGCCUAUGAGAGACGGACUCUUGUGAACUGAAGUAGCAGCUAAGCAGAGGUCAUUAUUAUUUUAAAAGCAGUAUCUAUUGGUCAGAGAGGACAGUCUUCCUUUUUUUCUAUUUUAUUACCUUUUAAAUAUUUACAUAGAAAAAAAUCUAGUUUUCAGAAUGCUUGACAUCAGUGGGUAUCUGCAAAUUAGAACUGUGGGUACUAAGUUUAAGCCUUGUGCUACCAACAGGAAACAUGAAAAAAAGUCUGUCGUUAAGACUGAUGCCCAGCUGGGCACGGUGGUUCAUACCUGUAAUCCUAGCACUUUGGGAAGAUGAGGUGGGAGGACUGCUUGAGCCCAGGAGUUUGAGACCAGCCUGGGCAAACUCCAGAUAGGGAGAUCCCAUCUUUACAAAAAAAACUUUAAAAAUUAGCUGGGCAUGGUGCAUGUGCCUGUGGUCCCAGCUACUUGGGAGGCUGAGACAGGAGGAUCAGUUGAGCUCAGGAGAUCAAGACUGCAGUGCGCUAUAAUUGUACCACUGCACUCCAGUGUGGGUGACAGGGCAAGACCAUGUCUCCAAAAAACAAAAAAAGACUGAUGCUCCUUCUACUUGUUUCUUUCCCACAGAAAAGCAUUGUGAUGGAUCUGUAAAUAUUAUUUAUAAAUAUAAAUGACAAUAAAGUGAAAUAUUAAUUGAUAUAAUUAUCAGUGAUAUAAUUUAAAUUUUUAUAGCUAUCAUUUGAGUUCCUAAUAUGUGCCAAGCAUAUGCUCAGCAUUUGACAUAUAUUAUUUCAACAUAUAAUGCAUAAGAGACAUUGUAUUAGUUAUCUAUUGCUGUAUAACCAAUAACCCCAAAAUUUAGCAGGUUAAACCCAUAAAAGUUCAUUAUCUCAUAUAGUUUCUAAGGGUCAAGAAUCCACAUGCAACUUGGCUGAGUGGUUCAUGAGAUUGCCGUCAUGCUGUCAGCUGCAUCUGCAGUCUCUAAAGGCCUGACCAGGGCUGGAAGUUCUGCUUCCAGGCUCACUCAGUGACUUUUGGUAGGAAAAUUCCUUGACAUAUGAGCAAGGAAUCCAUGAGUCUGCUUAAGACAUGGCUUUCCCAGUGAGUCAUAUGACAGAGGAGGAGAGAGAGAGCCCAAGAUGGAAGUCACAGUCUUUUAUAACCUAAUUUACAGAAGUGACAUGCCAUCACUUCUACCAUAUACUAUUAGUCAUAGAGUUUGACUGUGGUAAAUAUAGGAGGGACUACACAAGGAUGUGAAAGCCAGGAGGUGGAAACACUAGGGCUAUCUUGAAGGCUGGUUACCAUAGGCAUUAUUAGCCCCAUUUUACUGCUGAGAAAUGCAUGCUCAGAGAGGUUCCAUAAGUUCCCAAAGUCAUCUACCCAGGAAGUGAGCAGGCUGGGAUUUGAACACUGAUCUGGUGAACUGCACUGCCUGUAUGCUUUCCAGAAUGAAUACCCAAUGCAGAGAGUCCUGGAAGAACGAAGUGCAUGCAACCCUGGCUUUGGGUAUUCUAGCAUGUUUCUGAGGGUGCCCCCGGAUGGCUGUUUGCUCACAGAUACCUAUCUUUAUAUAGUUAGUAUGUCCCUGAAGAGCAGGGCAUAAACCAAAGAUUUGCAAAUUCAAUUCAUUUCAGAUUCAUGAUGGAAGUUCAAUAUUUAAGGGACUUCUGCUUAUAUCUUCCUGUAUCACUUGGUGAUUUAUCAUUGGCUUUUAAAUAAGCAUUCAGGUAGUGGAGUAUACCAGUAGUAUUGCAAUUGUGGGUGAAUGAAACUACCCUGAAGGGAAGAUUUUGUUUUUCUCUUCUAGAGUAAAUGUGGAAUUCAAUCUUAUUUAAAAAUAUUUUGAGAUCCAAGAAGGAUACUAAUAAACCAUGUGAAAGUCUAGUUAUGUUUAAGAUUCUAGGUGGUUGGUGUAUAGAUGGUGUUUUCCCAGACCAUCCCAAGCCAUCCUGGCUUACCACAUCCAGAAAAGGGCAUUUUUAUAGUUGCCUCCACUGCAAGAGGACCUGACCACUGAGAUACAUCUUCCUGUCGUGACCUACUUAAGGGAAUUUCAUUUUAGGGAAAGAAUUCAGGAAGAUUAUAUGGUCUGUAGCUGGCCUAUUAAAAAUGUAAACAUCUAUCUGCUUUUUAAUGUCCAUACCAAGCAAAUAAUCAAAGUUACACAUACUUCUGAAGCUCCUUUUCUUUGGAGAUCUCGGACUAUUUUAUAGAAACAGGAAAAUGUCACCUUUCUAGUCCUGUUUACCAACUCAUUUUUCUUAUUAAUUUGCUAAUCUGUCCUGCCUAGGUUAAGGGAAUUUGUUAUUCAUUCUACUCAUUUACUCAUUUAACACUUAUUUCAUACCUGUCCUGUGCUACAUGUAAUAGGUAUAAAAUUCCAUACUAGAUAUGAGGGGAAAAAAGAUGAAAAAGACUAAUUUCCUGCCCUCAGGGAGCUCAUAGUCCAAUGGGAGAUUCAACAAAGAGAAAGAAGGUUACAACUCAAGGUAAUCUUUGAUUUGUCAGGAGUCAUGCAGGAAAGAGUAAUUUACUCUGGUUAGGGAGUACUGAAAGAUUUAUCUUGGGUGAUGAUGGAUCUAGAAGGAUGAGGGGGAGUUUGCUAAAAGAAGAAGCAAGGAAGGGAAAUGAAAGUUUGGGGUGGUGGUGGAGGAGUUUCAGGUAGAAGAAAUCAUUCACAAAGGCAUAAAAGUGAGAGACAGCCUGGUCCAUUUUGGAGCAAGAAAUUGGGCCAUAAUUGAUGUUUGUAUCUCUACCUUCCAGAGUCUCAGAAACUAGAAUGUUUUUCUAGGACUGUUCCAAAUCCAAAUGUUGUCUACGGCCAUACCACGCUGAACAUGCCCGUUCUCAUCCAAAUGUUGUAUCAUUUAUCACCCAAAAUAUAGUGUAUGACAAGGAGCUCAAAACUUAUUCUCAAUGCCAUGACUAAUAGUGUUUUAAAACUAUAUUUUUCUGCCUGGUGUUCAUCAUGACCCUUGGGGACAUAUCUGGGACAUGUCACAUGGGCUCACCAUGAGUCAGGUAUGGGAAUGUCACAUGUCAAACUACUUUUGCUAAUCAAAUACACAAAAUGCUGAUUCCCUCACUGUUCUUGAGAUUUGCAGCAGUCACAAGUUCCAGUUUGCUAAGAAAUUCUCCUAUGCCUGAUUGGUUAUAUUAUUGUUUCCAUCUCUUUGCAUCAUUAGGGCCCUGUUGUUACAAGAAACAGCAAAAUAAAAGUAUUUCUCUUUUCGUUGUGGUAAAUUGGAAAUACCCUAGAGACUGUCAAAGAGGGAUGUGAAAAUAUUUCAGAAAUAUUAUUUCAUGCCUCCUGACUACAGGAUGGUGGUGAGGACUCCUUUGUCUGAGGCACUUAGAGCUGUUGAAGGUGUGUUGCCUGGAAAUGCACCUCAUGGGAAGACUUGCAGGUGUGAGCGGUUGCCUAGGAAUGUCAUUUCAGGAUUGAAACAGAGCUGUCAGUCAGUGCUGAAUUAGUGCCUACCUCAUCAUGGAACAUCUCAAGUGAACUCAACAAAGAUUCUUACCUGACCCUCGAUGAACCAAUGAAUAACAUCACCACGUCUCUGGGCCAGACAGCAGAACUGCACUGCAAAGUCUCUGGGAAUCCACCUCCCACCAUCCGCUGGUUCAAAAAUGAUGCUCCUGUGGUCCAGGAGCCCCGGAGGCUCUCCUUUCGGUCCACCAUCUAUGGCUCUCGGCUGCGGAUUAGAAACCUCGACACCACAGACACAGGCUACUUCCAGUGCGUGGCAACAAACGGCAAGGAGGUGGUUUCUUCCACUGGAGUCUUGUUUGUCAAGUUUGGCCCCCCUCCCACUGCAAGUCCAGGAUACUCAGAUGAGUAUGAAGAAGAUGGAUUCUGUCAGCCAUACAGAGGGAUUGCAUGUGCAAGAUUUAUUGGCAACCGCACCGUCUAUAUGGAGUCUUUGCACAUGCAAGGGGAAAUAGAAAAUCAGAUCACAGCUGCCUUCACUAUGAUUGGCACUUCCAGUCACUUAUCUGAUAAGUGUUCUCAGUUCGCCAUUCCUUCCCUGUGCCACUAUGCCUUCCCGUACUGCGAUGAAACUUCAUCCGUCCCAAAGCCCCGUGACUUGUGUCGCGAUGAAUGUGAAAUCCUGGAGAAUGUCCUGUGUCAAACAGAGUACAUUUUUGCAAGAUCAAAUCCCAUGAUUCUGAUGAGGCUGAAACUGCCAAACUGUGAAGAUCUCCCCCAGCCAGAGAGCCCAGAAGCUGCGAACUGUAUCCGGAUUGGAAUUCCCAUGGCAGAUCCUAUAAAUAAAAAUCACAAGUGUUAUAACAGCACAGGUGUGGACUACCGGGGGACCGUCAGUGUGACCAAAUCAGGGCGCCAGUGCCAGCCAUGGAAUUCCCAGUAUCCCCACACACACACUUUCACCGCCCUUCGUUUCCCAGAGCUGAAUGGAGGCCAUUCCUACUGCCGCAACCCAGGGAAUCAAAAGGAAGCUCCCUGGUGCUUCACCUUGGAUGAAAACUUUAAGUCUGAUCUGUGUGACAUCCCAGCGUGCGAUUCAAAGGAUUCCAAGGAGAAGAAUAAAAUGGAAAUCCUGUACAUACUAGUGCCAAGUGUGGCCAUUCCCCUGGCCAUUGCUUUACUCUUCUUCUUCAUUUGCGUCUGUCGGAAUAACCAGAAGUCAUCGUCGGCACCAGUCCAGAGGCAACCAAAACACGUCAGAGGUCAAAAUGUAGAGAUGUCAAUGCUGAAUGCAUAUAAACCCAAGAGCAAGGCUAAAGAGCUACCUCUUUCUGCUGUACGCUUUAUGGAAGAAUUGGGUGAGUGUGCCUUUGGAAAAAUCUAUAAAGGCCAUCUCUAUCUCCCAGGCAUGGACCAUGCUCAGCUGGUUGCUAUCAAGACCUUGAAAGACUAUAACAACCCCCAGCAAUGGACGGAAUUUCAACAAGAAGCCUCCCUAAUGGCAGAACUGCACCACCCCAAUAUUGUCUGCCUUCUAGGUGCCGUCACUCAGGAACAACCUGUGUGCAUGCUUUUUGAGUAUAUUAAUCAGGGGGAUCUCCAUGAGUUCCUCAUCAUGAGAUCCCCACACUCUGAUGUUGGCUGCAGCAGUGAUGAAGAUGGGACUGUGAAAUCCAGCCUGGACCACGGAGAUUUUCUGCACAUUGCAAUUCAGAUUGCAGCUGGCAUGGAAUACCUGUCUAGUCACUUCUUUGUCCACAAGGACCUUGCAGCUCGCAAUAUUUUAAUCGGAGAGCAACUUCAUGUAAAGAUUUCAGACUUGGGGCUUUCCAGAGAAAUUUACUCCGCUGAUUACUACAGGGUCCAGAGUAAGUCCUUGCUGCCCAUUCGCUGGAUGCCCCCUGAAGCCAUCAUGUAUGGCAAAUUCUCUUCUGAUUCAGAUAUCUGGUCCUUUGGGGUUGUCUUGUGGGAGAUUUUCAGUUUUGGACUCCAGCCAUAUUAUGGAUUCAGUAACCAGGAAGUGAUUGAGAUGGUGAGAAAACGGCAGCUCUUACCAUGCUCUGAAGACUGCCCACCCAGAAUGUACAGCCUCAUGACAGAGUGCUGGAAUGAGAUUCCUUCUAGGAGACCAAGAUUUAAAGAUAUUCACGUCCGGCUUCGGUCCUGGGAGGGACUCUCAAGUCACACAAGCUCUACUACUCCUUCAGGGGGAAAUGCCACCACACAGACAACCUCCCUCAGUGCCAGCCCAGUGAGUAAUCUCAGUAACCCCAGAUAUCCUAAUUACAUGUUCCCGAGCCAGGGUAUUACACCACAGGGCCAGAUUGCUGGUUUCAUUGGCCCGCCAAUACCUCAGAACCAGCGAUUCAUUCCCAUCAAUGGAUACCCAAUACCUCCUGGAUAUGCAGCGUUUCCAGCUGCCCACUACCAGCCAACAGGUCCUCCCAGAGUGAUUCAGCACUGCCCACCUCCCAAGAGUCGGUCCCCAAGCAGUGCCAGUGGGUCGACUAGCACUGGCCAUGUGACUAGCUUGCCCUCAUCAGGAUCCAAUCAGGAAGCAAAUAUUCCUUUACUACCACACAUGUCAAUUCCAAAUCAUCCUGGUGGAAUGGGUAUCACCGUUUUUGGCAACAAAUCUCAAAAACCCUACAAAAUUGACUCAAAGCAAGCAUCUUUACUAGGAGACGCCAAUAUUCAUGGACACACCGAAUCUAUGAUUUCUGCAGAACUGUAAAAUGCACAACUUUUGUAAAUGUGGUAUACAGGACAAACUAGACGGCCGUAGAAAAGAUUUAUAUUCAAAUGUUUUUAUUAAAGUAAGGUUCUCAUUUAGCAGACAUCGCAACAAGUACCUUCUGUGAAGUUUCACUGUGUCUUACCAAGCAGGACAGACACUCGGCCAGAAAAAAAAAAAAAAAAAAAAAACAAGCAAACAAAAACAUUGUGGGAUGUGCACUCCAUUGGAGUGCAUGACAUGGCAUUGGGAUUGGAACAUGUGGUUUCGAGCACUGAAAGCUGCAAACCAGUGAAGAGGAAAAGAACCUUGUGAUUAAAUAUAAAACCAAAAGUCAAAUGGUGCUUUGUGUUUUAGCCUUCAGUCACCAUGACUGGUCUCUCCCCCAGAUGUAUAUAUACCAUAGCAUUUGUCUACCUGCUGUCUUUUCUUCAGGACAGAUGUUCAGGAAUUAUAUUGAUUGAAUUUAGACUCUGUGCAUGUUCUUAUGGAAAUGAUGUUCAGAAUCCAUGAAGAAACUUCAGGCCAAAUUUGAAACCCUGGAGGGAAAUGAGCCAUAAGGGAAGUAUAACAAGCCCUGAAGCCUUUUAUGUCGUUGUGCUUCUUUGGGAAGGUGUAGAGUGUGCCUUUUUGUGAAUCCUCCUCUGAUCAUGAGGGUCUUUCCCACAGUUUCUCACAGUGUGUUUACACUGCCCUUGGAAUAACACAGCGCAUCAGACCAUAAGAAGGCUAGAUGUGGAUGCUAGAAUUGAUUGUUGGUUGAUAGUUCUCUUUGCUGGAUUAGGAAUGAGGCGCCAAAGGAAGCACAGCCAGGAAAAUGGCCCCACAGCCUAGAUCAGCAUCUGUGGGAAAGGAAAAAGGGUUCCCAUGGGGACAGCCCCCAUAGGAGUUUUCUGGAACCAGUAACACUGAAAAAUAAGUGUGUGGCUACAGAUGAGCACGCCCACCCCUUGCAACUCCCUGUUUACAAGUUGUCCGAGGCAUUGGAGUGCUUAUGGUCAAUGGGCUCUAGGGAAGUAGGAAACUCCAUCAUGAUACAAAUGUCUAGUAAUUUUAAAGUUUCUUUCCCUUUUUUUCUGUGCUGGAAAUGUUCACAGAUUUGAUUCCCGCCCCAAGAAUUACAACAAUGUAUUCAUACAGUCAGUUGGAAUCCAAAGGCAAUUAAUUCUAUUUUGCAAAAUAUGAUGGUCUUCCUAAAAAACAAGUACUGAGUUCUCAUUUCAAAAGUUACCAAGAACUGAAUUCUUUAAACUAGCAAACCGAAGUAACAUGACCAUUUUUGCCUUAGUGGGAGGUUUCAAAUGUGCAGCUCAUGGCAUUUACCUGCCGACCAUCUUUUGCCAAGUUUAGAAUUCUUAUGCGUUUCAAGUUCUAUAUAGAAAGUAAUUUUACUUUUGAUUUUUCUCUUGUUAAAAAAAAACUCCUUUAUUCUAAGAACAAUGUCUCAAAGUCUCAUUUUUACUUUAAAGGUAUAAGAGACUUCUAAAGAGACUUACGGGAUAUAAAAGUAAUUCCUGGAAAUGAUAUUUGAUGAGGAGAAUGUAAGAGAAUGAAAAACACAUUGAUGUUUUCAUUUUUAAAAAAUACAACUAGCAUGAGAAAUCAAGAAAAUAUGUUUACCAAAAUGCAUUGCAAUUUUCCCAAACCUGAGUCUUCAAAUAACAAACAUGAACUUAUAGGUACUGUGAACUAGAAGAAUUGGUUAUAUCCAGAUUUCUGGGAGAUAAAUUAAAACAUAUUUUUGUGGCAUAAAUAAGCUGAUUCAGAAGUUACAUUUCUUAACUUUAGGUAGAGGAGAAUAUUUGUAUCCUUUUGUUGCUAUGCAACUGUUUAAUGAUGAAGCUUCAAACCACAAUUUUGUAUAUCAUAUGACAAUCAAUUGUUUUCCAAGAAUAUUUAUUAUUUUAAGUACACAAUUUCAGUGAAUCUUGAGUUUUUCUAGGAGUCCCUUAAAGGGAAAUUAGCAUUCCAUGAGCCAGUAAAAUACCUACUCUGGUAAAACAUUAUUAUGGUUAAAAAGUAAAUUCAAGUUAGUUUUUUAUAAAGAACUAUAACAUUUAUUUUAAACAUUUUAUAAUAACUGAAAACAUUAAAGUGAGCAAAUGAAAUUUCAAAACCACUUGUAAUAAUGUAUUUUAUAAUCGCACUGUGAUACUAUAUAACACAGUCUCUUUUGUAUUAAAAUAGUAUUUUUUUCACAAGCUGAAAAAUAUCUUUUCCUUUGUUGACAAUGUUUUGUAAGAUGACUUUAUUUUCAGAUCUUUUUCUCCUUUUUUGCACAAAACUAUGCUUAUGGUUUGUGUCACAGAAGUGAAAAUAUAUCUUUGCAUUUUUAUAUCUGGUCUGUUUUUCUUGUUUCCUUUGUUUUUAACUUGAUAUAGAUUUUCUUCAAAUAUAUAAUGGCAAUUUUCAGAUAUCUCACCUUACCAUAUCUUUCCUUAUUUUCACUGCAUGCAUUUAAUCACUGUAUUACUUAAUGUUUGAUUUGUUAUUAUGGGCAUUUCAAAUAGGCAAGCAUUGAAUUGUAAUGACAAAAAGGCUAUUUUAUAUUAAGGAUAUAUGCAUUUGUAUUUCACACACCAGAGAUGAUAUUAAACACUGAUUAUUUUAUGCUGCUGUUUAUUAAAAAUGUUUACUAUAAAA